UGAUCACCAUAAUGUAGUAGCAAAUGUCUACAGCCUAAAAUAAGGCUGGCAGAGACUUGUACCCAAGCCUUAUGACUUUCUAGCUGUGUAACAUACACAAAAAAAAGUCACUUAUUCUUUUACUCUGAUUGAGCCUCAGUUCCCUUACAUUUUGAUACGCAUCAAAAUAAUAGGAUUCUCUUCAUAAACUCCUCACGAUUAAAUGAAACAAUGCAUAUUAAGUGCUUAUCAGAGAUCUUGGACAAGGAUGACAACUCAUUAUGAGCUAGUUCUUACAAUUACGGCUAUUUAAAGCCAGGCACAGAAAGCCAAAUAUCUGACGAUCUCACCAAUAUGUGGAAUCUAAAAAAGUCAAACUCAUAGAAACAGAGAGUCAAAUGCUGGUUACCAGAGACUGGGAGGUGGGGAUGGGGAGCUGUUGGUUAACGGACACAAAAUUUCAGUUAGACAAGAAGAGUAAGUUUAAGAGACCUAUUGUACAUCAUGAUGACUGUGGUUAAUAGCAGUAUAUUGUAUACUUGAAAAUUGCUAAAAAGUAGAUUUUAAGUGUUCUCACCACAAAAAAAUAAUUCAGUGAGGUAAUGCAUAUGUUUAUUAGCUUGAUUUAGCCAUUCCACAAUAUAUACAUAUAUCAAAACAUAUUAUACAAUAUAAACAUACACAAUUUUUAUUUGUUAAUUAAAAAUUAGAUAAGCUAAAAUUAAAAACUAAAAAAAAUUGUGACCAAGCCACUAUUUUUGAUGUAUUCUCCGUUGAGGUUUUCCAUACCAUCCUGCAAAAUACUUAGAAAAUAAAUAUUUAUUGAAAUGAGUAACUCAUGAGAAUAUUACUUUUUUGAGAUAUAAAAUUAUUUUGAAUACAAAAUGAGCAAAGAUAAAAAAGUGUUUUUUCAUAAAACUAAUUUGUGACAUUUAGGAUUAUAGGAUUAAGUAAUCAGCAUAUUAAAUAAAACAACCAAAAAUUCUUCAACUAUAAUGUUUAUUCUGUCAAAUGCAUAAUGUAAAAUAAUAUUUGUUUUGGCAAUUACUGAAGACUAAGCAUUUGUUUGCCUCCCACAUAAUAAGCAGACUAAAGAAAAACACAUUUGGUAGCUUGAAAAAUGGCAUCUUCAUAUGAAAAAUUAAAUAUUUCUAUAGACACAUUUUCAUUUAUUUGUGAUAAAGAUUUAAUUUUAAGUAUUUUUAAAAGUAUUCCAUAACACAAUUCCAUUUGUUGUUGUUGAUCUAUAUACUUACCCAUAUGUAAAAUAUUUUAAAUAAUAACAUAUUUGAAGCCACCGGGCACAAAAAUGAAUGAUUGUGAAAUGUGCAAAGUAUUUGAAUAGUGAGAGCUAAUUCUAUACUAUUAAGGACAAUAAAAAGUGCAAAAGUAAUUGUAACUGCUAAAAUAUUAUUUCAAGUUUUAGUCCAUAUUUUGAUCUAUGGUCUAAAUUGAAGUUUAUUGAUUCUGUAACUCAUUGGAGUUUCAACCUAGAGAAACCAGUCACUGUAUUAUGCUGGGGGCCUUAUAAAAAGUAUAAUUGUGUAGAAGAAAGAAAAAUGGGUAAGAGAAACGUAAGGACAGGAGACAAGUCAGCUAUUUAGUUACCAUGCAAUGCAGUUAUUUGGGAGCUUUUUCUCAAAUGUAAACUGAGAAUAAUUAUACCUAAUUUAAAGCUGGGUGGUGCAUAGAGCACUUGGAUCAAUUUCUGGCAUAUAGUCUGUGACAGAGCUAUGUAAAUAAAUUAAUGAAUUUAUAUCUAGAAAUCCAACUCUGUAUACCACCAAAUCCCUUUAUUAUUUUCUUUUCUCUAAGCAUUUAAUGUAAAGUUUGAACUGUAUUAUUCUUUCCUACUAAUUUAAAUUGCUGCUUGCCCUAUUUGAAUAAAAAAUUGCCUAUUUCUAUGGUUUUGCUAAAUAGUGAAUAACUAGUGCCCUUACAGGAAUCACAAGAAAAACACACUGAAAAAUGUACUUGGAAGAAAGAAUAUAUGGAAAUAUAUGAUAAAGAAAUAACUGGGAAGAUGCCUUAGGAUAAAUUAUGAAAGAAAAUAUUUUAGCUACCCUUUUCUGUUGAACAAAUGAGAAAAUGUGGUCAAAAAACAAGGAUAAAUCUAUUGGGAAAAAAAAUUUAUCUCCUAUUACCCAAAAUUUUACCUGAAACAUGUUUUUAAGGAAAGAGAGAACAAACAUAUUCUGAAACAUAGAAGAGGUGAGUUUAACUUGAAAUUAAGAGCAACCACCCUCCCCAAGGGGAAAAAUAUCUCCAAACCUCUCUCCUCAUGUAAACAGAGACUUUAGAGUAUUAGCAGUCAACAAUAUUUUCAUUAAUUAUUUAUAAUGUAGAAAGCCAUGCCCAUUUAAUUCCAUUUUCAUUUAAAACACUACAAAAUAUGAUAUAUCUUCAUUUUAAAAAUUAUGUGAAAAGAAAAUAUCUGAAUUAUCUUCAUUUCUUUUUGAUGAAUACAAAAAGAGAAAAAGGAAGUAGUUUUUACUUUACGAUUUCUAUAUCUUUAGGAAGAUAAUAAGGAAUCUUAAAAUCCAACAUAUAAAAUAUCACUUUCUACAGCAAAAUUACUUUCAAUAAAUGGAAACCUAUAAUUAAAUAAUUUACCUUCCUUAAGUCUGAGAACCUCACAAUCAUGCUCUUCAGUUCUUUUGACUUAACAAAAUAUCUAUAUAAGUGUAUGACAAUGUCAAUAGUCAACUGAAGGCAAUAUAUUCGAGGUAAAUUUUAUUUUAAACUUUUCUUCUAUUUCAUACAUAUAGACUACAAAAUAGCAAACCUGGCAUUUAAAUAUAUAAUUCCUUCAAAUUAAUUAAACUAAAACAUGUCAUAAGUAGCUUUUAUACAUGUUUUAUUAAAAAUAACACUUAGAAAAUAUUCAGCCUAAUUUAUCUUUAAAAAUGUCAAAUACCAGGAUACUUUUAAUGAUUUUUGAGCAUAAAAGAAAAGCAACUUUUCUUUCUCUGUGGUUCAAAGAUACAGACAUGGGAAUAUUACCCAGUAAACUAUCCUUGUAGGAUUAAAUUUUCAGUGACCAGAAGCUAGAUUGUUUUGUUUUGUUUUGUUUUGUUUAACAAAUUAGGCUCAAAUACUGUCCAAACCUAAAAGUGGAUCUUCAUCAUUACAUAAAUUCUGCAAGCCUAAACAAUGACAGCCCGAGACUGUUGUACAGAGACAUAUGUGAGACUUUAUCCUGAUCCUUUAAAAUGAAUAGUCAGAUGAUGGUUUCACACUGAUACAAAUUAGAUUUCAUAUGCUGAUAUGCUCAAUAAUGCUAACAAGGAUCUAUAUAUAACUUAUUAAGUGCUACAGGCAGAGCCUAUGCUAGGGCUUUACAUCUACCAUUUCAAAUGCUCAUCAAAAUCACAAUUAACCUAUUGAUAAGUUUGUACUGGUAAUUUAAAAUUUGGAGGCAUUCUUUUUCCAGUGGUUUUGAAAUAUUAUGUUCAUUAGAGAAUAUAGUGCCAAGCCUCUGAUGCCUUUGUUGGUUUUUAUUUCAUGAAGUUAGUGUACACAGCACCUCUGCCUGAGCAGAGCUGAAACUCCCAAGUUAGGACAUGAACCAAAUAUAAGGGCCACCCAGAGCUUGGGUUUAGGCAGCCUUCCUCACCUUUAGCUCCUAAAGGGUGAAACAUCUCAGAUGAAAAACCUCACUAACCAAAACUCCUAAUUACUAAAUAAAACUUAAGGCAUUCAUAAACGCUUGAAUGUCUGAAAUUGCAAGUCUAUACAGUUGAAAAUGCAUUUUCUGAAUUCAGAUAUUUGCCCUUGCUACAUAAUAACUGUAGAAUGUUGAGCAAAUUACUUAAACUCAGUGUCUCAUUUGUCUUAUCUGUAAAAUUGGAAUAAGACUAGCACUGCCUCAUAGACUUAUUUUGAGGAUUAGAGUGACUUAAUAAAUAUCAAUACUCUUGGAACGAUGCCUGGCAAAAUUAUUAUUGUUUUGCCUUGUUGUUAUCUUAGAUAGGUUGUCCCUAUACCAUGCCAAAACUAUUCUGUCAAUUUGAGGGGGAAAAAUUAAGAGUCAAAAUAGCAAGUUGGUGCUUGAACAUUUACUUUCCUUUUGGUUAUUUUAUCAUUGUGUCAAAGAAUUACAAACAACAUAAUCCCUAUUUUCAAAACUUCCUUAGCCCUCUGAUCUUCCCAGAGUCACAGAAAGUAGUAGUUGAAUGGCUUUAAUCUAGUUUGUCUUAGUAAUAGACCAACAAUCCAUCAAGAAACAAAUGCCAUUCUAUGGCCCUAGUUAGAUAGAAUUCAUGAUUGUUUUUUCCCCUAGGACUGCAUUGCAACCUCAGACAAGAAUGGCAGACAGCCAGCAGGUUCUGCCAGCUGGCUUUGCACUGCUCUCUGGGUUUUAGAGAACAGGAGCACAGAUAUUUUUGAUUCUGCAGGCCAAUUCAAGCAUAAUUUACAGUGAAGAAGAAACCCUUUAAUAGUGAUUUCGCAUGUAGAGAAAUUAUAUUUUUAAUAUAAAAGAACAUCACAAUUUUUUAACAUGCGUGCAUUUGAAAUGGAUACUUACAAAUUAUCAGCUAACAUGGGACAUUUCUUUAAAAAGCAUGUUUUCCAACAAUUGAUUGCAAAUCCAGUAAAGAUAUAAAAUGACCUGUUGGUUUUGAGAUAUUUUAUUCAUUCAUCUCUUCAAUACAUCUUUAGUGAGUGUCUACUAUUUGCUCAACACUGGCAUGACUCUGUAUUAACUUUAUUAUUGACAGCUUUGAUGUGGCACAUUCUGCUGUAAUAUUGUUGCUUAUACUAUACUAAUAGUGGAAACUAUUGCUCACUAACUAUAACUAGUUUAAAAUAAAAUCUGAGAUUAAAAUUUAGCAUUUAACUUUCUUAAUAAUUGAGAUUAUUGCUGAAAUCAUUAUGAAUGUUUUUAGUGUAGGGAACUUUGCCUUGUCCCUCAGUGUACUAGAACAGUGCCUGACAGUUAAGAGUGCAAUGUAAUAACUAAUUCAGUAAAUAAGUAUGAAAAUCUAAGAAAUGCAGAAUGUCAAUUAGAGGAAUUAUGCUAAUGAUGAAAGGCUACGAACCCUGGAAAAAAUUUUCAUUUCAAAAAUAUACAUAAUAUUCUCGAAAUAUAAUUUUUAUUUAUAUUUAAAAAGAUGUGCAUAAUUUGUAUUAAAUACAUAUGAAUGUAUUAUAAGGUAAAAAAGAUGCAUGUCUAUAUUUAAGUGUGGGUGGAGAGAAAUACAAUCUACUCUAUUUAAAAGUUUCUAAAAUGUACUUGUGAAAUAUUAAUAUUUUUCACCUAAAAGAGUUUUUUCUUUUUUCUUAUUCAAGAAAGUUUUCUCUUUGAAAUUUAAUGUAGCGCUUAAAAAUAUUCAGUGCUUUGUUUAAUACGCAAACUUAGCAUAAUUGGAUUUUGUGAGCCUGGCUCUUAAAACACUAUGUGAAAACUUUUUCUCUAAUACACUUAGUUCAAUAUGCUUUAUACUUUUUAUCAAAACUUUGUAAUGAAUUUUAAAAUAAUUUUAUAGCUAGAUUAUUUUAUAGGUAACACAAAAUAUUUUCCAAGAUGAAGUUCUUUGAAGCAAAGUCAUUAAUUUUGUUAUAUAAUUGAAUUUAGCUCCUACUUUUUAAUCUAAGUUACUUUUAGAAAUAUAAAUUAGAAAGUCAUAUGAAUAGAUAGACUCCUUAUUGAAAGUAAAGUAGCAUUAUCUUGUAAUUGUACAGUAAGACCAAACGCAAAUGUGACAAACCAGGUUAAUCAAAUAAAUGGUCAUUGAAAAUUGCUAUUAAAUGUGUAAGUGGUGACUAAGAGAGGCUGAGGUAAUGAUAAUUAUAUUUCCAUAGUUUUCUGAUAAAGUAGAUGUUUUGGAUGGAAAAAAUACUGAGGUGAUGUUUAUUUACUUAUUAUUUUAUUCUUUCAUUUAACAAAUAUUGAUUUAAAUUGACGCUUUGCCAGGCACUCUUCUAUUACUAAUACUAAAUUUGUGAACAAGCCAGAUAACAAAACUGCUCUCAGGGAACUUAAAUCUGGGAGGAGAAGGCAGAUGUUAAUACAUUAUAACUAUGGUGAAAUCAGGUGGAUUUAAUUGUGAGAAGAAAAUAAGAAAGACCAGAAAAUGAUGUGGGGAGACAGGGCCAAUUUAGAUUGAAUAGUCAAGGAAGUCUCCUUUGAACUGAGAUCCAAUGACAAGAUGCCAGCCAUUACAAGAUUGUGAGUCCUAUUCUCUAGGCAAAAGAAAGAGCCAAAUGUUCCAAGGGAGAGAGCUGAUCUCGGUGUGUCUGAAAAAUGGAGAGAAGGCACAUUAGAGUGGAGCAUGGAGAACUGGAGGAAGGAAGUGGAGAAGAGGCUAGAGCACAUGCAAAGUACACCACAUAGGGCCUUGUAGGCCAUGGAAAGAACUGGACUGAACUACAAGUAUCAUGAAUUGUGAACAGCAUAUUGGUACUAUUUAUAAUUUUAGAAAUUUCUUUUAUGUGGAACAAUAGCUGUUCUAUACUUUUUAUAGUUACAUGAAUUUGGAUUCCUGUUGGUGAACAUUCUUAUUUCUUAAUUUGAAUACUCAAUACCAUCAAAAUGCAUGUAAUUUUUAAUUCAUUGCGGUUUGUCAGAACACUAGAGGCAAUUAAAAUCAUUUGACAUAGUAUUUUCCUUUUUAUCCUUUUACAUGAAUGCAUUUUUCAGUUAUUUCAAAAUUCAAUUGAACAAAAUCUAAACCAUUUAUUUCACUAUAUCCUUCAUAAAACAUCACACUUUUUAAAACUUGUAUGGAUAUGUAUCUCUAUCUGUUUGAUUUUAUAUUAAUCCAUUGCUUCUCUAACCAGAAAGAAUAGUAGUGAACAAUAUCUUUUCAGGUUAAUGAUUUAAUGUGUCAUGAAAUUUUUCAUGAAGUGUAUCAUGAAAUGUUUCAUGAUGAUAAAACUACUUAUUUUCUAAAAACAUUAACUUUGAAUUGAAUGUGGACCUCCUAAAAUAUUUUUUUCCAAAAAGAAAGUCUUCUUCCAUGAAUGAUGAAGAUUAGUGUUGGUUACUGAGUUCGAGAUUUUAUUUUGGUGUAGUAUUUUUUCCCUUUUCUUCAUUUUCCAGACAUGAAUGUCUGCCAAACACACACUGUAUUUAAACCCCUGAGAAGUUCAAAAGGGAUUGGAGACAGCAAAGGGAGGUCUUUUAUAUUUCAAUAUCCUCUGUAAUUAACAUUUCUGUCUUAGCAUUAAUAAAACUAAGCUUUUGCCUACUUUUGCUUUUGAUUUUAGUGGUUGAAGCCAUUAUUAUUUGUGCAAAAAGACAAUCUAGUAACACAAGUGUAAAUUGGAGGGUAAUUUGAAGAGAUAAUUUGCUGUUGUGAAAACAAGUCCAAAUAUUUGUUCAUGUAGUUGUUGGCAAAAUGGUGAUCAUAGACCAAUCCAAUUCUCCUCAGACACCAACUGGUUGUUGUUGAGUGCUUGGCCUUCACAGUAGUCAUGUGAUCAAACUCCAUCAUACAUGCUUGAAACAUCUUUAAAAAUGGAGAGUACUCUUAAUGGAUGAAAUGUGGAUGCUGCCUCCUUACCUCUACAUUCCUAAAAAUAAUCUACAUUCCUAAAAAUACACUUCAAACUGGAAACCAUCAUUCUCAGCAAACCAACACAAGAAUAGAAAACCAAACACUGCAUAUUCUCACUCAUAAGUGGGAACUGAACAAUAAGAACACAUGGACACAGGGAGGCGAACAUCACACACUGGAGCCUGUCAUAGGGUGGGGGAUGGGAGGGAGGGAUAGCAUUAGGAGAAAUACCUAAUGUAGAUGAUUGGUUGAGGGGUGCAGCAAACCACCAUGGCACAUGUAUACCUAUGUAACAAACCUGCACGUUCUGCACAUGUACCCCAGAACUUAAAGUAUAAUAAUAAAUAUGUAUAUAUAUAUAUAUACUUUAAUACUGAUUAUGCUGAUCAUAUAAUCGCAAUUACACACAUAGUGUUGAUCUUAUGUGUGUAACUAUGCCCACUGAUUCUUGAAAAAAUGACAAUACAUUUGUUUACAUAAAUUGUAAAGAAUCCAAUUGAAAGCAAGCUCAACAUAUAGAGUAGUAAAAACAUGAAGUGUAUCUUAGGGACAUCUCUGUACCUUCCACAUAGGGCAAUAUAAUAGGUCACAAUUUAUAAACAGCCAUCUACCAGUGUUAGUUCCUUAUAAACAAUGAUGCAAACUAGUGUAGGUAAUAUAAACUGAAAAUAUGGAAAAGAAAAAAUAAUUUGUCAGUAAUAACAGCCCUCACUUUGAACUAUAGCAAUACUAUUGAUGAAUAUCAGUAUUAUUAUAUUUUUUCCAGGAGGUUUCUCAUUUUUCUAGAAAGUGGUAGACCUUGAGUUUUUUAACAACCAAAUAAAUAAAUAUACAAAAUCAAAUUAAACAUAAGAAAUUUAAGUUUAUUUUUUUCAUUGAUGUGGGUGCACACACAUUAACUGUAAAGCAGAAGUAAAUUGAUAGUUGGUUAUUUUACUGGCAACUGUGUUUUGUUUGAUCUUGACAUCUGAUACUCAUGAAAUUUGUAGCGUGCUGUGAAAGACUCUGACACUAUUAAAAAUUUGAAGCUCCAAAUAAACAUACUGGAUGCACCAUUUUCUGAAAGUCAUUUGUGAGAUUAUGUACUAAAGCAAGGGUCUUAAUUUCAAGUCUUAACUAUUCAAACUCUACUAACGUAAGUUCUGAAAGAGGAAUUAGGGUCAUAGUAUUAAAUCAGCUGGAUUUGGCUACAAUUUUACAGAAUCAAUUCUUAACUCAGAAAAUUGUCAAAAUUCAUUUAUCUUAUACCUCAUGUGAAAGUAGUAUGGCAGUUCAUAGAAGUAAAAUAAAAAAUCGUCAAAUCUGAAAUUUAUCUUUCAAAUAAAUGUAGAUACUUUUUUGUGUUUUAUCUUAAAAAGAGUUUUGUGUUUUAUAUUAAAAAAAGAGAAAAAUCUCAAAAUAUUUAUACAUAUACAAAAUAUAUAUACAAAUAUAUAUUAUAUGUAUAUAUAUUUUUGAGAUGGAGUCUCACUGUGUCGCUCAGGCUGGAGCACAGUGGCACGAUCUUGGCUCACUGCAACCUCUGCCUCCUGGGUUCAAGCUAUCGUCCUGCCUCAGCCUCCUGUGUAGCCUGGGAUUACAGGCACGCACCACCAUGCCCAGCUAAUUUUUGUAAUUUUAGUAGAGAUGGGUUUUCGCCAUGUUGGUCAGGCUGGCCUCGAACUACUGACUUCGUGAUCUGCCCGCCUCGGCCUCCCAAAGUGCUGGGAUUACAGGCGUGACCCACCGCACCUGGAUAAAAUAUUUGUAUAUUUUAUAUGUAACACUUGUUUUAUAAUUAUCUGUACAAUUCAAUAGGCUUUUAUUCUUUCUGCAUUCUAUAAAAAGGUUUUCUUUAUUGGUUAAAGAGAUACACAUAUAUUAAUUUCAAAAAUUGCUGAAUGAACAUGAUUUACAAUAUUCUGAAUAUUUAAUAGGUAUGUAUAUUUAUCAUAAUCUUGAAUGACAAAUUAUAAGAUAGUUAUACAUAAAUUAAUUUAUAAAUGUGCCAAGAAUUUUCUUAUAGUUUUUGACCAUAUUUUAUAAAAAGAAAUUUUUGUACCUUUUAAGCUAGAGGACAAUUCUCUUACCCCAUUAUUUUUUUUCUAUUAAAAAAUCACAUAUUAUUAAAGAAUCACAGUUGAAUCUGUAUUACAGAAAACUUGAUCUGUCUCAUUAAUGGAACCAAGUAACUACUGUAUUCAGUAAGAAAAAUAAUAAUUUAAACAGCUAUAUAUCAUAACAGUUAUUAGAAUCCCCGGUAACCAAAAUUUAGUCAUAAACCAAAUUUACUAAUUUUUGUUUUUAUAGUGAAAUGUUACAAUUUAAAAAACAAACUGGAAACACUAGUGUGUAUUGAAUUUGAAUUUAUAUUUUUAUAGACAAUGUUUUCCUAUAAAUAUUUGUGAGAUUUUAAAUUGGUCAUGAUCUGCAUAUGACUUAGCCUUAUGAUACUUCUAUAUUAAGUUACAUGUGAUUUAUCCAUUGGAAAGCUAAUGGAAAGCUUAGAUACAUUGAAGAGAGACACUAUUAACGUGUAAAAAUAUAAAAUUUGAAUUUUUUAGUAAGUAUUCAAUGAGCACCUACUCUGGAAAAAAAUAAUGUACUGGAUCUUUGGAGAACAUGGAUGUAUAAAACAUCAUAACCUCUAUUCACCAGUUUUCGAGUAUCUCGACCUAACUCUGCCCAAGGAUGAAACUCAUUAAUUCUAGAGUAGCUCAUGAUACGUAAGUCAACCUGAAACACAGAAAAACUAUCUUUAUAUGGAAAACUUUUAAAAAGAAAAGUGCUGCAAGAUAAUGUUAUUUGACAUUUGAAGGGAAGAGAUACAUAUUCCAUUGUUCAAAAAUGAUGCAAAAUCUGCUCCAUUACAUGAGUAAUAUUAUAUGAGCCAUAGUCUAUACAACAUAAAAAUACACAAGUGGACAUUCUUAGUGUUCUAAUAACAUACAUACAAUUUUAACCUGAAAGAUCAAAUUAUAUAUAUAAUUGUCAUUGGCAAUUAGGCAUAAUAGAACUAAAUGUUUUAGAAGAGAUUUUAUUUUUUUGGUAAAAGAUUUCAAAGUUUAAAUAGAAUCAACUUUCACUUAAAUCCAUUUAAUAGUUUGUAAUAUUGUCCUAUCUUGAGUCUCAAUUAUCAUUGUAUUUAAUCAUCUUAUAAUAAGAAGGCCAAAUAUGAAUUAAGCAAUCUCCUAAGAUAUCUCAUAAAACUGUAGCUUUUUUGUUGUUAUUGUUCUUACCUGAAUACAUCCAAUAGUAGGCACUGAUUACUUGGUAAGGCAAUUUUUUGUUCCAGGACCAUUCUAAUCUUGAGAAAUGUCUUCCUGUUUUCUGUGGGCCAGAAAAGUUUAUCAUCUUUCUUUAGUAACAUGUUGCCAUGAUUUUAAAGAGAUUAAUUAUCUGGGGCCAGCCCAUAGUUCCUUCUUAGUAGAAGUACAGAAAUCCCGCGGGGGGCGGGAACUGACUUACCUACACACUUCCACAUAACAUACAAUGGGUUUUGCCAUUAAGAUCAGCUUUAGGAGUAAGAAUCCACCAAUUUCAUGGAGAAUUGGAAACUCUCCCUAUCCAAAUUAUCUAACUUGUAUGUUGACAGUGGUGUCCCGGUGGUAAUUGAAGGAAAACAGUUGUAAUAGUAAUAGCUAAAUUGUCUUGAACACUCACUAAUAUCAGCUUUACAUUCAAUGUUUCCUUCAAAGUCAUACAAUUUAUGUUUACUAAAAUUCCUUAAGCAGGAAUGGUUGGGAGAAAGGUAAACCAUCUAUUCUUCUCCCCUAACCUUUUAUUACAUGGCAUCUACAAUAUAUUGGAUUUUGAUUUUCUUACUGUUGUUUAUUUUCAUUUUAUUUCAGUUUCAAUAAAAUAAACCUAAAUACCUGAACAUUGGACUAUUAUUCCUUUUAAGGGAAAUGACCUAGGAAAAGUAAAGAUAGAGUUUUUUGACCUUUUUAAUUUUUUUUUAAAUUACAGCACAUUACAAGGCUAUUAAAAGUGUUGUAAAUAAUGUAAAAUCUAUUUAAAACUCUAAUAUGGAGAAAAAUUACUCUAAUUAUAUGUGCUGCAGCAUCAAGGAAGUUUUUUCCCCCAAAGGGCUUCUCAUAUUUCAUAAACACUGAUGAGUUUUCCCUUCACCGAAGUAACAUCAAAAUUAUAUUUGUAAUUUAGAAGUAAGUCUCCUUGUCAGUAUAUUUCAAGGAAUCUGAAGAAAUAAAAGCACUAUUUUUAGCAUACUCCAAUCAAGCCAGUAAAUAAAGAUAUGGAAUAUAUAAAUAUAAAGAAAUUUGUGUAUUUAGAAAGUACAAUUAUAAAAGAGGUUCCUUUCAAUAGAAGAUGAUUUAUUGAAUUAUUUUCUAUAACAUUAAGAAAGUCUUGAAAUAGAAAAAAAAACAAAAUGAAAUCAAAUAUUAAGUUCUGGUGAUUGAUUUUAUUGUAGGCUUUUGUGUAUGUAUUCAAAAAGUAGGAAGAUGUUCUGAGGGAAAAAUGUAUUUCCUCAUGACAAGUGGAAGUUCAUUCAAGUAUUUAACAAAUACUGGUGAGUACCUGCCAAGUACCUGAUUCUAAGGGCUGAAGAUAUAGCAGUGCCCAGAACAGAAAAAGAUACCAACCUUCAUUUAGUUUAUGGGAUAAUAGAGAGAAGCAGAUAGAUGUACUAAGUUGUAAAAUAUUUAGUAUGUCAGACUCUAAAAUUCUAUAGAGAAAAGAAAGGGAAAAAGGCCGUAACAGCAGUAAAUACAUGAGUUGUCUGUGGGCCACAAAUUCAUGCGACAGCAUUCAAGUUGUGAGGGAUACACUGGAAGUCCUGGCCUCUUGUGGAAAUUAGAGUAAACAGAGGAUUCAUUCUGCCUGUCUUGAUGCAGGUCGUGGACAGACUGGGGGUGUCUGUCCUGGUGUAAGAAAUGACCAGAGUCCUGCCAGGAAGAAGCAGUGUUCUGGGCUCUAUCUUUACUCUGCUAGAGCACCACGGUAUCCCUAGGCCGUAUUGAUCAUUCUGUCAUUUUCAGGUUAACAUCUCAUCACCAAAACAUUUAUUUUAGUGCCUACUGUGUCAAACGUUAUGCUAUAUCUUGUGCAUACAAAGAAAAUUAAGACUUCAUAACCGCACAUGAAAAGCUUAAUUCUGGCACUUUAAUAAUACCUACUGCUAUAACUUUUGAUGUAAAUUAUUUAAAGAUAAGAUUUUCAUGUUGUAUUUAUUAAAGUGUACAUUUAUGGCAAAGUGUGUUUAGACAGGGAAUUUAACAUUUAUUGAGGUCCUCCUCUUGUUUGGGUUUGUGGUAGGUGCUUCAGGUACAUUACCUUAUAAAAUCACCUUAAAACAUUAUCUUCAGUUGGGUGUCAUGUUUCCCAUUUUAAAAGAAGAAAAAAAAAGAUAUGCAAGUUCAUAAAGCAAGCAAGUGGCAAAGCAGACAAUUGAAUCUUAAGUAUUCAUUUAUUCUUUCUGUCAAAAUAGGAUGCCUGCAAAAACCACCCCAUAAAAUAGAUUCAUUCUGUAGCUUGAUAAUAUUAUCAUAAUUACCUAUACAAUAUGGAAAAAUCAAUUAGUUUAUAUGAAAAUACAUUAAAUCAGAAUAUAUUACAUAAUACAUAAAUAGAUUUAUGUAUAAAUCAGAAUAUAUUACAUAAUAUAUUAUAUAUUAGCUCUCUGGGAUAUCACUUGUCUAGUUAAGGACCAAGAGAUUGAGUUUCUCUAGCAAAGCAAAAUGAUUACGUUUCGGUAAUGAUUCUUAGAGAUUUACAUCGUCAAAGCAGUUCUUUCCAGAAGUUGCAUACUUAUUAGAGCAUUCAACACUAAAUUCUUCUCUUAUGUACUGAUGAAAGUAUCCGAAGAUGAGCUGUCUGAAACCAAAAUAUAAAAUGCCAAGUGCCGUUAGGUCAAACACUCUGAUCUGCCUCCCAGUUAUUACUGUCAUGAAGCUACCUUUUAUUUUGUCAAAUGAAAUAAAAAUGUGAGUUUGCCUAUGCUUUACAACCAAAAAAGCAUCAUCAAAACCACAAGUUCUUAGGACUUAAUAGAAGCAAAAUGAUCAAGAUGACUGUUUGUACAAAGCAUUGAUCUGUUUCUCUGCUUUAUACUUUGAAGGUAAUGAGUAAUUUAAUUACCUCUCAGGUAUAUAGAGAAAAGUUUUUCUCCAAACAUUUUCUAGGGUCUGAAGUAUCUGAAAUUGAUCAGCCAGCAGCCGUGUGAUCACACUGAAAGUAUGCAAAUUUUGGUUUUGCCUAAAGGUCAAAAUAAUAGAAAAUCACACCAAGCUAUUAAAAUCUUACUUUAUUUUUUUGUGUGUUUUUCUCAUCUUGCCAGUUUUCAGAAACUCAAGGAAAAUAAUCUGUCAAGGAUUCUUCACUAUCUGAUCAGCCUGAGGCAAAUAACUUCAUCUCCCUCUGCCUCAGUUUCCUCAUAUCCACAAUCUCCACAAUUCCAUGAAAAUCCUACUCAUUCAACUAAUAUUCAUGGAAUUUCCCAUUUCUAAGCACAGAGGGUCUUUCUUAAUCCAUUAUUUUAGUUGAAAUACUGAAUUUAAAAUUACAAAUUUUGAAGACGGAUCAGUUUUUCUUUUUUUUUUUAAGUACUGGUUAUGUUAUUUCUAAAUAUAAUGUUACCUUAAGGGCACAUGGUACAACUUCAAAGAAACCAGAAGCUCAGGCUACAGUCUCUGUCAGUUUUCAUAAGAACAUAUCUCAACAAUAUAAAACUGAACAGAACUCAACAGUUCACUCUUAGAGCAGAAUCUGUGUCAAUCAUUCUGCUCUAAUGAUCAGUACUUAAAGCCAAGAUAUUUUCCCCAAACACUAAAAUAUGGUUUUCCCAUGUUCCAGUGGUUAUUUGGUAAUAUUUCCACUUUACCCUGUAUUACAACUUCUAAUAUUUCUAUAAAUAAAAUAGACUUAAUAGAAUAUUGCAGUGGAAAUGAAUAAAAAGAAUUCAUGGAAAGAGUCGGCAGAGUCCACUAUUUUGGCCCUUAGUAAAGUCAUGACAUGUCCAGGUUUAACCUCUUAUCUGGAAUAUGCAGAAAAUCAAAUAUUUUUUUUACUUCAUUUGGGAUUGAUCAGGUUCUGGGACACUGAUCUCUAUUAUAUGUUUCAUAAAGAAAUGAUUUAACAAUCAGAUCAUGUUUUAUUAAUAUAUAAUUAAGGCAUUUCAAUCAACCAAAAGAUUCCUAAUCCCUGCAGGACAAAGAGGGCAUGGAAGUUGCCUUUUAUGACAGACUCUGUAUUGCUCCUCCCUGUGGAUAUGGAAUGAUUUCUGCCCAGAAAUGGCUAUCUUAAUUGGCAUUGCACUGAGUAAAUAUAUUACAGUUACUGUUUUUUCUAGCCUCCAUGCAUUUUUUGUGCUCCCAUUCACAAUUUUAUUAACUUAUUGUAAAUAUUUCCAAGGUGAAUGGUUAUCUAAUAUAAGUGUAUGAUUAGUUUAAUUACUUUAUGAAAUUAAAGUAUGCUAUGAUUUAUCAUCCAUUUAUUUACAAAACAUCUCAGGGUGAGUUAUUUCUAAAUUGCUUUGCUUCGUCUGUUUCCUUAUUUUCUAGGUAGAAAAAUAAUUUAUUUUUUUUCUUAUUACAUCUUCAAAUUGUUUUCGGUAUUUAUAAUUCCUUUUUGCUCUUAAGAUUCUGAUUAAAUUCUAACUGCAACACAAACAAUAAAUAUAAGCUUAUGCUUUAUCCAUAGGGAAAAAAAUCCAGGGACAUGUAUACCCCCUUCUAUCCAGAGAGAAUUGUUAUAGAAACCAUUCUAACCAGACUUAUUUGCUGACAUAUUUUUCUUAUGGUUAAAUUUUGGUCCUCUUAUAAUCUAAGCCUAGAUAGACAGAGACAUAGAUAUAGAUAAAGAUUUUGUCCUCAUUGUCCUCCAUGAAGGAAAAUUACAGAUAAUGACUAAUCAAUAUAAUAUCUACUUGUUUUCUUGAACAUUGCCAUCACCAAACUAGUACUUUAAUAACUAACACCUAUCUCAAUAUAAUCCAUUUCACUUUUGGUUGUUGUAAUUCAUUUUACUGCAAUCGAAUACCAUGUUAUUCUAACUUAGUCUUCAAAGUGUCAAGUACCACCCACAACAGGUUGUUCUUUCAAUUUUUAAAAAAUGUACUCUCUCUUUAAAUAAUAGUCAUUCAUAAAGUUAUCAGAUAUUACUGAUGCCCUAGUACCAUCUCCAAUAUUGUUUGACCCCUUCUUCCUCCUCUGUUCACAUAUAUCCAGCUUGGCAUUAUCAGCCCCCAACCCUGUUGUUUCCUGCUUUAUUCAUGUACAUCCAAGAAUCACUACAUUUCAUAUCUAGAAAUAAAUUAGAAAUUGCUUCCUCACCAUUGAGUGGGCCCCAGAACUAUUUACCUACUAGGUUGUAAGCUUCCUAAGGAAGGGCAGUUGUCAUCUUACAUUUGUAGCCCAAAUGCCUAGCAUAGUCCAUGUGGCAUAGUAGGUGUUUAACAGAUAUUUGCUAAGUAAAUGGAUGAGUGAAUAAUUGGAUAAACAAAAGCAUGAACUUAAACCCUGACCUCCUUGCCUAGUUCUUAUAGUUCCUUUAUUGCAUAUCCAGUGUGUCAGUUCCUAAACAUUCAAUUUCUGCCUACUGCCUUGUACUAAACCUGGGUUAACUUUUUUAGACUCUAGGACUCAAAUAAUAAAAAGGCUUAGGGAUUUUUCUGCCCUUUUAAUUGAUUUCUCAGCUCAUCUUAAAUCCCUAGAUAUUUACAUCCAUCUGGUUCAGACUGCAAACAUUUAUUUGUUGAUUCAUUCAAUUGGUGUAUAUUGAUUUUUUAAUGUAAGUUGUUGAAUUUUGCAUGCAACAGGGAGUAAACACGCAACAAGCAAAGCCCUUGCCUUCAUGAAAAUUGCAGUCUAGACAAAUAGAGUAAUUAGAUAAUUAUUGCAAAAACACGCAAAGUUACAACUCUGAAAAAUUCUACAGAAGAGGGUAAAAUAUACCGUGUUCUGAGAGCUCAUAGUAAGGAAACUUGACCUUAUCGAAGAAUCUAGGCUUUCACCAGUAGUGUACAUGUGAGCUGACACCAGAAGGACAAACUGGAAAUAACCUAGAUAAUGUGCAUGGGAAAGAGAAUCCAGGCAAAUUAUUGAGAGGGCAGACAAGAGAAUGAAAAGUCCCCUGUAUGUGGAAGUUCAGGCAAUGCAGAAAGGCAUGUGUAAGAAAAGAUCAAAGUAGACAUAGCCAGAUCAUGCAGGGCCUUUUAGAUUAUGGUGAGAUUUUGUUUAAGAGUAAUGGAAGGCCACUGAAAGGUGUUGAACAAGAGAGGAAAAUGAUCAGAUUUGAUUUUUAAAUUAUCAUCCAAGCUUCAGUGUUGUAAAUAGGUGAAAGUAGCACUAAGGUGGAUGUAGACAGAUUAGUUUGUUGUCAAGAUGAGUUUUCUGGCUUGUACAACUAGACGGAUGUGGGUGUUAUUCAUUGAGAUAGAAAACACACUGAGUGUGUGGGAAGGCUGUGAAUUUGAUUUUGGACAUGAAUAUGUGUUUGGAAAUAAAUCCUAGGAGAGAUGUCUUAUAGAAAAUUGAAUAUAUUGGUUGAGAGCUCAGAGAAAAUAAUUUGUGUUUAGGUAGUAAUUCAAGCUGUGGAUGUGGAAGAAAGUAUACAAUAAAAAAAUGGAGAGCCUAAGACUGAACCUUGGGGUGCGCCAACAUUUCAUGUCUAUGUACACGAGAAUAAGCCUGCAAGCUGAUAGAGGAAAGACUAAAAUAAGGCAAAUAUGUGAGAGAAGACCUGGAAAGACAUGGUUUAAGAGUGAGAGAAGAUGCUGUAUCAAAAAAAAAACAGUCUCCUUUGAGAUCACCUAAAAACUGAAAAAUGUCUGUUAGAUUUAGUAAUAUGGAAGUCUUUCGGGAUCCCAGCAAGGGCUGUUUCAAUGCAGUCAUGGGACCAGUCAACACAAUGGUGUGGGGUGAGGAGAUAAGUAAAGACAACUCCAGCCUCUCUGAGACUUUUUGGUCAUGAUGUUGGUGACACCUUGGGAAAGUGAGGAGACUUAAAUGCUGGGGAAACAUUUGCGAUUGCCUCAUUUCUUUCACUUUAUUCUAAACAUGGUAGUGAUGGAGUCCUAGAGGCUCCCCAUUGGGACUACCUACUUUGUUAAAUUACUAAAUGUGAUGAAUAUUUGUUGACAAUAGUACCUAAAAAUUUGUAUUAAUAGAAUCAUAAAGUCUUCUACAAGGCUCAAAGUCCAACAUAAUUGAUGACAUCGUGUCUGACUUCCAAUAUUCAUGACUUCCCAGGUGAGUUUCCAUAUUUCUGAAAGUUUUCUCUGUAACACUUGGAAAAUACAAUUUAGAAUUGGGAUAUAUAAGAAAGAUAAUAUCAGGGAUGGAAUGUUAGGUGUAUCUGUCAUUUGUGAUAUUUUACAAAGUGAAAAUAGAUUUAUUCAUAUAUUUUUACCCCAUCUUCUUCCUUUCGUAUUCUUUUUUUCUUCUUGUUCUCUUUAAGAAAUGAAUACCUAAUGUUUAUUCCGUACUGUACAAGGCACUAGAUGAUAAAUAGAAAAAGGAAAUUAUGAGAUAAUGAUAAAUACACUGAAAUUGCUGAAAAAGAAAGGCUAUGUCAGAAUGAAUAAAGAUAAGGUUAAAGAGAAUAGCAUUGAGAGGACAGGUAUGAUAGAUACUUUUGAAUGCAAGGCUGAGACGUGGUGGAGAAUAAAGCAGCAUUGAAAAAAAUAACAUUUAACAGAGAUUUCCUAGCAGCUCUGUGAAGGUCUAAAAAUAAAGAGAGUUUGGUUAUUGUAAUAAUCUGGAUAUCAAUUUUAGGAAGUGUAUAUAAAUGAAAAUCAUUAUGUAAUGGAAGUAGUCUGAAGACUCAGUAAUCAACAGGGGCAUGCAAAGGUAAAGGCAGUGAAUUUGGAAAUAACAGGAACUUUUUAAAAAAGAUGCUUUAAAAGGGAGAUGUUUUAAAUAAGUAAAAUUAUAAUUAUUGGCUUAUUGGGCAUCAUGUGUUGGUAGGACAUCUAAGUGUUCAUAUAAUAAGCAGGAGAAAAUGCUCACACACUUGGGGUUGCCCUGUAACUCACCUCAAAUUAUCACUGGGAAUACCCACUUAGUAACUAGCAUUUUCUAAGAGAUGCUCUACAUUGAUAAAUACAAGUGAAAAUGUCCAUUGAUUGAAAAUAUGUUACACAUCUAUUAGAUUUAUUUACAUAAGACUGGAAAGUUAUAUUUUACUUCUAAUUAUAAGUAAAGUUAUUUUUAAUAUAUUCACUUCUACUGGAUGUUAUUGAGUCUAUUCUUAGAUUACCUAAAUAGAACAUUUCAACUUUGUCACAGAAAAUGUACACAAUAAUCUUGAUUUUCCAUUUAAAAUUCUUAUGAAGAAGGCUUAUUUUUAAGAACUAAAUUCUAAAUUUUAUUUCUCUGUUCUUCAUAGAUAUGUUUUAUUUAAUUAUUGAAUUUAUUUUGUUUUCUUUCAAAAUAAUUUUUAAGCAUAUUCAUUUUGCAUCAAUCUACACUCAUUGUAAAAUCUAACAUUGACUUAUAGCUAUUAGUUAAUUUUAAACUAAGCAAAAUACACUCUUUUUGUCUUAUUAAUUGUGUAUUUGAGAAGAUCCAUAAACUUUGAAAAAAUUCUAUUUCUUCAAGAAACAAUUUUUAAACUUCUAUAUAAUGAAAUAUUAAAUACUUUAUUAUAGUUAAGGAACUUUAUAUAUUUUUUCUCUAGAUCUCAUAAUGAUUUAAAAUCCAUACAUGCUUCAAAAAUGCUUUAGUAUGCUCAUUUCUCCAAUUGUUUAACUGAAAAAUAUCCUGUAAUGAGGUCAGUGAUUAUUUUUUAUAAAAUGCAGAAUUCCUCAUUCAUUCUUUACUCUGAAUAAGUAUUUAAGUAGCUUUUUCCAGUAUGAGUUGUUUGUUUAUGCUUUGCUUGAUUGAUAAUCAGAUUCUUUACAACUUUUAUUUGAUCUUGUAAAAUAUGUGAUUUAUUUAACACAAUGGUGGGUACAUGAAAUGAUUAAACUAAUAGUAAUUACAGUCUAACCAUUAACCAGUGAUAUAGAUGGUGAACAAAUCAACCUUAUGUAUCACUAGUCACAUACAUGGGGAUAUUGGAAGGGUAUCUUGCUAUCCAAAAUAUUUAUUGUGUCUCUAGGAGUCUCAUAAAAAUUUAAGUAUCUUGGGAAAAAUGGGUAUGUUGUAAAGGGCAUUGAAUUGGGUUUGCCUUGAGAAAAUCAGUUAAUUUCUUUAAGUUUCAGUUUCUUCAUUUGUGACAUACAGAUAAUAAUUUUUACCUAUUUCACAAUGUUAUUCUGACUAUAAAUUAGAUAAUAUAGGUAAAUUUAUCAAAAUAAAAAGAUGAUAUUAAUGUUCAAUUAAUUAUUCUUUUGAUCACCUAUCAAAUUAAUCACUAAUCAAAAUUCUGAGGAUAUACAUAUAUAUAUAUAAAAGUAAAUUUUCAAAGGGGCAUUGGGAAAUGAUUGUGGAUCUUUUACAUUGGAGAAAUGGGUAUUGCAGUGAAGAUACCCUGGAAACUAUUUCUGUGAGUGGGAAAAAGAUGGCUUGUGGUGCUGAUAAUGAAGAGUGAGGUGCAUAACUGGGACUAGAAACACAAUGGAAAAAUUCUAUUUCCUGGUUUGUCCUGGAAUCUAUUCUGAUAACAGUCUAUGGCCUCUGCACAGAUGUUUUCAUAUGGAUUAGCCACCAAGCAGUUUAAUGCAUUAAGCCUACUAUAACAGCAACAAAUUAUAAUUUGUUUGUAUUGAUGCACAUGUUAGAUAGAUAGAUGAUAGAUAUGUGAGUAUAGAUAGAUAGAGCGAUAGAUGAUAGAUAGGUAGAUAGGUAGAUCGAUAGAGAGACAGAUGUUUCCACUUAAAUGCCCUCAUUUACAUAAGUUUAAAUAGACAUAUGAAUUACAGCUCAGGCUGAUUUGACUUCAUUUAUGGUUCCUAUACCUUUUGAUGUUUGCCUAAAGAUAUAUUCAGCUUAAGUGCUAUAUUAGGAAUAUUUAUUUUUCUUCUUAUAAAAUCUCUGAAUUCAAGAAUAUUAUUUUGUUUUCUAUGUAUUUUUAUGUAUUAAUUCAUGUAAUUAAAUAUGUACACUUGUGAGAUAUGUACACAGAAUACAGAGUUUGUACAUAUGCAGACAAUUAUAAUACAAAAGUGAAGAUUACAAAUGCCACAUUAGUCAUACAGAAUGUUUGGGGAUUCCAAAGAGGGUGUGAUGACUUCUCACAGGUGGUGAAAGUGGGCAUCUUAGAGGAAGUGUCUUCUGAGCUGUGCCUUGAAAGAUAACUAGUAAUCUCUUUAAAAAGAUAGACUGGAACUCAACUAUGAGCUAUUGAACGUUUUAAAAUAGAAAGGUGAUGUCAUCAGAGAGAUGCUUUAGGAAGAUUGAAGUAGUGGCUUGAACCAGGUGGACUGGAAGGCAGGGAAUGACUCUGCAGGUAAAAAUGCAGUCAGAUCACUAUUUUAAUAAUAGAUCAAAGGUUCCCAAGCACUGAACCCCCUGCUACAGAAGCAUCUGCAGAGACUUUUGAACUGCAAAUUUCCAGGCCCCUCCUCAGGGCCUAAUUCAGUGGGUCUAAGAUAUAGCCCCAGAAGUAAUAUUAAAAACCUGCAGAGUGAUUUUGAUGCAUAGCCAAGGUUAAGAACCACAGGCUGCAAUGAAAAAGCUCUGGCCUCGCUGAUAGACUCGAAGGAGGGUGAGAAGACAAGACAAUGGGGUCAAAAAAGAAAAAAAAUGUAGAAAUGACACAGAAGAUAUUUUCUUUCCUGUUGUCCAAAUUUCAAAAUGAUAAUUUCCACUAUUUGAAUUUAAUAAAAUACACUUGCCAAAAAGUUUGUCUUAUAUAUGUAUUUGUCUGUAUUUUAUCUAUAGAUGUAUUGAAUGGUUCUUUUCCUGCCAUUUUUCUCUUAUUUAAAAAACAACAAAAUUUGUCUGAAUAAGCUUACAAUAUUUCUUUUUUUUCUAUUUAUUCUGGCUAGAAUUUUGAAAAUGUUUUAAAAUUUUAUGUCCUUUUACAAUUACAUUGAUAUUUAAAAUGACUCUGCUUCUUACCAUGGAUAUUUUUAAGAAGAAAAAUAUCAGUUGAUGAGAAAGAAAACCACUAUGCUUGAGACCAUUUUCAGGGCUUUGUUAUCUACUUUUCAUCCCAAAUUCUAUAUAUUUUUAUUAAGAUUCCCUAAUGCAUAAGGAUAGAAAUUGUAUUUGUAAAUGCUAACUUAAAAUACCAGUAUUUAAUUAUGUUGUGUUGAUAGGGAUGAUUUAUUCUAGACUUUAAUCGGAUGUUUUUGUACCUAAAUGAAAUUUAGUCUUAUUUUAAUUAAAUGGUAGAACAUGCCAAAAAUGAUGGGUAAAACUAGAAGAAAUGAACCCCAACGGAAGACUCCGGUUUCAGUUAUCAGUUUUGUAGCUGUAAAGUAGUUAAGCUCUGUGGUUGAACCUGCCAGACAGGCAUUAACAUUAUGGUAUAGGAUUCAUCUGCUGAGAUAAGAUUUUCUCUUAUUUAACUUUAUUGAAAUGUCUGAAUAAAUCACUAAGCCAAACGUAUGGUUUCUUGUUUAAAAUAUAUUAAAAUCAUGGCAUAAAACAAAAUUCUCAUGUGAAGUAAAUAAUAAAAAUAAUUGUGAAUGUAUCAUUCAAAACAUUUUUUCAAUAAAAAAUGUUUGAGGAGAGCUCAGAUUUGGUUACUGAAACCAAUAUUCCUUUGAUAACUUAUUUCUCUUUUUUGUUUCAAAGUUCAGACUAGUUAAAUUGACUUAUUUCUCUCUUAUCCUACUUUUUUGUAGUCUUGCAACUAAAUAAAUUUAGUUAUUACUUAUUGAUCUGUUCGCUUGAACCAUCUGACAUUUUUUCCUAUUGUGUACAUAUAAAAUAAGCAAAGUAUCCUUUAUUUAUAAAGGACUUGGUUAAUUGUACCCAAUGAAACUAUCAAAACCUUUUUUAAUUACUUCUAAAACUCUAUUCUCUGUUCAAGUCUCCGUGUUUAAUAUUUAAUAUUGAAACCAUAGUGUUUACUGUUUUGCUACCUAAUUUCUUUUUAAAGACUUUAUUUUUUAGAGCACUUUUAGUUUCACAGACAAAAUUGAGAGGCAGGUACAGAGAUUUCCUAUGUACCCCCAUUCUCACAGAUUCAUUUCUUUUUUAAAAAUAUAAACUUGAAAACUUUUCUUUUUACAAUCUUAAUAUAAAUUCUCAAAGCAUUUACAAUUGUCCCUGUCCUUUAUUAGAAAAUUCUCGCCCAGGCUGGAGUGCAGUGGCAUGAUGAUGACUCAUUGAAGCCCUGACCUCAAAAGCAAUCCUACCACUUCAGCCACCCAAGUACCUGGGACCACAGGCAUGCACCACCAUGCAGAGCUAUUUUUUUUAUAUUUUGUAGGAAAUAAAAGAAAGAAAGUUCUUUCCUAUAUUGAGUUGAAAUGUUUUCUUAUAUUUCCACCAAUAGCUCAAUCCCUUGUGGCUACACAGAACAAAUCUUACCCUACACGGCAGCCUUUCAAGAAUUUGAAGACAGUUGUAUUUAUCCUCCUACAUCGUCUCUGCUCUUGGCAGUUUUUCAUGAGUCAUGGCUUUGAAUUCUUUAUCAUCCUGUCUUCUGAAUGUAUCCCAAUUAGUUUCCAUACCCAAAGUUGACUGUAGGACCCAGUUUUAGUCUGAACAUCACAGCAAAAGGAACAAUGAGAGCACUUGGACACAAGAAGGGGAACAUCACACACUGGGGCCUGUGGUGGGGUGAGGGGAGUGGAGAGGGAUAGCAUUAGGAGGUGUACCUAAUGUAAAUGACGAGUUAAUGGGUGCAGCACACCAACAUGGCACAAGUAUACAUAUGUAACAAACCUGCACGUUGUGCACAUGUACCCUAGAACUUAAAGUAUAAUAAAAAAAUUUCAAAAAAAAAAAAAGGAAAACCAAUUUUGUUCUUGAGAAUAAAUUUCCGUUAACACCCCUUGCUGCCCACCCACACAUCCCCACAAACCUGCCUAAUGAGAUUAGCUUUGAAGAUGGUUGUUUUGUAAUCUUGACUCAUAUUGAAUUUAAGGUUGACGAGAAUUGGGCCUUGGACAGAACUAAAGCCUACGUUGUUGGAUAGCCUAAAACACAAAAUUUGUUAACUCUUAAGAAUUAAUGUUUUAUAUGGAACAAAGUCUUUCAGGAAUUCUAAAAGUCAUACAUCAAUAAAGAGAUUUUUAUGUCUUUGGUAAGGCUUUUAAGUACUGUCAUAUUAAAUCCUCCCUAAAAUAAUUUAGCUCAGAAAUGUACAAGCAAUAUUAACACAGGUUUUUUUGCUUAAAUAGUUCAUUAGCCUCUGUAACUUCUUGAAUAUAAAAAAUAAUGCCAGGAUUUUUUUAAGGUGUCUUUAAAUCUGCUAGCAAGUUAAAGAAAAGGUUAAACUUUUUCAGACGCUAUGCUUUAAUGAAAACAACAGAAGACACAUGUUUUAUUGUAAAUAAGUAGAUAACUUUUCUAUUAAGAUUUGGAGCAAGGCUAUGCACCAUACAUGCUCUGAGUGGGCUUGAUUCCUCCAGGGAAGAGGCCAGGAAAGCAUUGAUGUGAAAACAGCCUUUCCCUUGCCAUUCUCUCCAUUCCAGGCAGGUUAUCUGCCAAGAAGCUCAUCCCUAUCUGUAAAACUGCCAGCAUCAGUUCAUGCAGCAUUCAUGUGUAAUUUGCUUUUUCUGGAGAGCCAUACCAGGGCAGAGUUGACUGAUUGAGGGAAUUAAAAGCUACAGACUCUGGGACAGGAGGGCUGCCCUGUGGGUAUAUGAGCUGGUUACAUUUUGGCCCCUUUUCAAACCAGGGAUAUGCAACUCUUGAUAUGUAUGGGAAAGGCAGAACUGCCAAUACUGACAGCGCUCCUGAGCAGCGCAAAUGCUCCACAUGGCAAAUGCAUCAUUCACAGAGGACUCAUCAGAGCAGCACCCAGAAAAAAACCAAACAGAGCAAUACACAGAGAGACCAACUGGGGCCAGAUUUUGUAUAUAAAACAUUCCUCGUAGAGUGACUUAUAAUGGGUAGAAAAAGGAUACGUCCUGAAUGGCAAACUAUUAUAGUACUGAUUAUAGUACAUCCAUACAAAGAAAUAUCAUGCAUUUAUGUAUGAUGAUGGUAAAGAAAAACCUUUAAGAUCUUCAGGAGAAAUGUUUAUGACAUACUAAAUUAAAUAUUAAAUUUCAGUGCAGUAUGUAUAUUGUUACCUCAUUUUUAAAUUCUUAACUAAUUUAUUUGGAAAGAAAAAUGGUAAUUAAGAUCAAGAUGUGGAGACAGGACAAAUGAAAGAUUAUAACGAAAAUUUUAAAAGAGGCCAGGAAAGCAUUGAUGUGAAAACAACCUUUGAGAUGACAGAGUUAUUGAUGACUUUUCAUGAUUAUUAAUUCCUGUCUUUGUGCUCCUAUGUGUUAUGCAAAUAUUCCACAGACAAUAAAGUUACUCCUUUUGUAAUGAAAGUCUGUGUAAUUAAAUUUUUUUUAAAAAAAGUUGUGACAGGUAUAAAAGUUUCUGGUUUAUGAACAAUAAAAACUACCUCUGGGGACCUUGAGCAAAAUAAUGAUGGGUUAGAAGGCUAUUAAAGAACUCCUAGAAUCUGCUGGGUGGCUAGAUCCAAGCUUCUGAAGGAUGUCAAGGGAAGCUCCAUACCAGGUGAGACCAGGGAGCUGAACACAAAGCUGGAUCAGGCAGACCAAGAGAAUAGUCUGGCUACAACUCUUCCACUUGACAAUCGAUCUGUGCCACAGCCUUUGACCCCUGGGCUGUCCUGCCAUGAAUAAUCGUUAGUUCCCCUUACAUUUUUGCUUUGCUUUGCCAAGAAACAAAAACUUAAGGUGGUGUAGUAUAUAUGCAGUAUAUAUUACCACCCCAUUUCCCAUGGCAUAUGCCGAUGUCUGAGCUUCCAGGGACUUGCAUGUAUAUUUACUGCUUCCUUUGGCUUCUAGUGAAGGCAUUUCUCAUAUUUUGAGAUUUCUGUAACUCCCUGCCUCCAAUAGAAAGGUGUUGGAUGCUAAGUAGUGGCAAAUGUCCUGCACAUGAAAUGUUGGAAUAGAAGAUAAAGUAUUGUGUUAGUACGUCUCUGGAUAUUUUUAAAAUCCUUAAAAUAAAUUUUUACCUGUCCAAGAAAGUCUAAUUGUGUGUGCCACAAUUCCUAAGACUCUAGAACAUUUCCAUAAUUUGUAUUAUAUAUGUCAAGCAUAAUACAAAUACAUUGUCCUAGUGAUCAAUGUGUGAUCUGAUUUAUGUAUGCAUUGCCAGCCUCAGACACCAUAUAUUAGUAGCAAUAUAUUGUAGAGUAUCAUUGGGCUAUUUUUUUUUCAAAGAGCUAUGGAAUUUAGUCUUUUUGAAAUACUAAGGCAGAAAAAUGUGAAGCUAACUACCGAAAUUUAAAUAAAAUAAAUUUUCAGUUAUGAGUGAUAUAUAGUAAUGUGUCUUUAUUAAUGGACUUGAAUGAAAUGUGCAAACUAAAUUAAAAUCUUGGAAAUCUAUAAUUAGGUUAAUAAUGUAGUGAUGACUUCUUACCAGAGAAAUAAUAACAUUUGAUAGGAUAUGCUUUUUUCUUUCAUAAGAUGUUUUACAAGAUAAGAAAUAAAGUUAUAGAUAUAAUACCUGUGACUGGGUUGUCUUAUGAGCUAAUAGAUCGCAUUCAACAAAUGAAAAUGAAAAGACAAAAUAUGCAUCAUAGACAAACAGAUGAUGCCAUCAUCUAUGAAUGCACAGUAUGGGUUAUUGGAAUGGCUUUAACACAUUGAAGUUGGUCUAGUAAAAAUUCAAGAAGCAAUUUAGUUUUUAAUUCACAUGUUUUAAUUUCUUCUUUUACCCACUUAGGUGCAUGCAUUUUUAUAAACUUUUAUAACCAAGUUCUCUAAAUAAGCAUUUUUUAUUAAAAUGCUUACAUAACCACAUUGAGAAUAGAAAUAGCUCUUUAAAUAUUGCUAUUACCUUGGGGUAUAUAAAGUAAGUCUCAACCGGCAAUUCAAAACCUUCUAUGAUCUAUUCAGUUGAAAUUAAUCCCCUUUCUUUCCCUUCAUGUUUCCACUAAACUUUGCUUUAACCUUUAUUAUCUGAUUCAAGUUUGUAUUAUAUGAUGCUGCUAAUAAUGAUGAUAAUGAUGAACUUUUAGUGAUUUGCAAAUCAAAGAUUAGACAGAUUAGCAGGUUUGUUCAAGGCCAUGCAGCUGACAAAUAAGGUAUUAAUACUAAGAUCCAGUCCUCAGCAGUCAGACUUGAGUCCAUAGUUUUCAUUUCUACACGAUUGAUAGAUUAUCUAUUUUCUUCUCUGCAUCAUCAGUUUUUUGAAGGUGAGGCAUUGAUUUUUAUUUAGUAUUACAACUUUGAAGAUACUUAGGACCACCAUGACCACCAAAUAACUAAAAUUAAAAGAAAAUACACCAAAAAUUUUAGUACAGUUGUAUAGUGUGAUUAUAAGUUCUCUAUCUCAUGUUUUUACCACUUUAAUUUUUUUAAUAUUCUAUAAUGAACAGAAGUUAGCAUAGGGGAAUACUUUAGAGUAGAAAUUUUGGUCAAAUACAACGGAUUUUAAAUUACUUCUUCCUCACUUUACGACUAUAACAGGUUAUCUAUUGCUUCAUCUAAUCCAUGAAUUGGGAGCUGUUGGUGAAACCGAUACUCAAGUUUGUUGUAACAACUAUAUAUACACUUAGAGUCUCUGGCAGAAAGCAGUCAGUAGAUGCUAGUUAUUAUUUUUAAAUCAAACAAAAUAUUUAAGGAGAGACUUUAAUAUUCUUAAACAUAACCCUUCAAAUCCUUAAACCAGAUUUUUUUUCUGUACAAGAAAGUCUGGUUGUAUAUGCUACAAUUCCUAAAACUGGAACAUUUCAAUAAUGUUAUUACACAGCUCAGGUCUUGAUUCUAAUGCUCAGGGUGGAUAGAACAGGCAAAAAGUGCUAGGUAAUGAAGACAUGCCCCACCAGGCUUCUUCCCAUUGGUAUGCUGCCUUGACACAGUCAUAUUUAACAGUGAACUCUGUUUGGAAGCAAUUUAUAUGCAUAUAUAGAUAUGUUCACAUGGCGCUGCUGAGAUAAUUACAAUGUUAUUUACUAGUUUUGUCUGGUAUUUCUGCUAUGUCUUUAAUGACAAAAUGCUGCAGAGACACGGGUGAGAGAGACAAAAGAUGAUGAGGAUGAGGUGAUUUUGUAAAUAAGCAAAAAGAGGAAUAUUUUUGCAUACUUUUGUGCUGGAUGAAACCAGUAGAAGAGCAAAUUUAGGUCUAAGAGAAGGUAAUAAAUUAUAUGCUUAAAUCAAAUACCUUUAAAGAAUAAAAAAAAAAACUUUUGAUCAUCACAGGAAAAAUUUCAAAAUAUUUUAUCUUGCAUCAAAAAGUUACAUCUAAAUAUUACUUCAUAAAAAUUAUCCUAGGGUUUACUUGACUUUUCUCCAUGCAAUUCCAAAUAAAAUAAGGUUUUAUGAACUCUGAGAUUCUUUGAACAGUUUGAAGAACUUGAACUGGAAUAUCUCUUACACUAAGCACAGGAGACUGUUCUCCAUAUUUAACACUAUUUUCACAGUGUAUACUACCAUAUCCAGUACAUACUAUGUGCUCAAUAAAUAUACAAUGAAUGUGUAACUAAUAGAGUCAAGAGGCAUAAAGGACUUGGAGUUGCAAGACCUCGCUUCAACCCUAGGCUUUGCCAGUUGUUGAUUAUUCAACUUUGGGCUAAUAAUUUAUCAUAUAAAAUGUUGUUUAUUAUAUUAAAUUUUAAAUAUAUAAUUUCUUAAGAAAACAUAUUAUAAAGUAAAUUUAUUUAUUUGGAAAAUUAAAAAAAUUCUCAGACUGUAUUAAGGAAAUAUAUGUAAAUGAUCCUUGCAAAUUAUAAAUGCUAAUUGUUUUAAAGUCACUUCCAGGGCAGAAUGGCAAUGCUCUUAAUAUUAUGAAAUCAUAGAGCCUCUGUUGAAAGAGACCUUAAAAGGCAUCAAGUUCAACCACAUCUCUGGUUUUUAAUUAUCUUUCUACAUAGGGACCAGAUGGACACAUGCUGUAUAUUUAACUUUAUCUUUAAGGAAAUUGUUAACUGUAUCCCUGGUAUGCCUCAGAAUGUUCUCUUUGAAUUAUAAAGGAGUGUUCUUUUCAGUACUUUAUUUCAUUCAUUUAGUUCUCACACAACCCCAUGAAGUACUAUUACUGUUCCCAUUAAACAGAUGAGAAACCUAAAUAAAAAAUGUGGUUACUUGCCCAGCAACUCAAAACUAGUAAGUUGUAUAGUCAGGACGAGAACCCAGGUAAUCUCCAGAGCCCAUUCCCAUAACCAGUACAGAGUACCCUUUCCAUGUGAAGUGGAAUGUGAAAAUCUCCUCUGCUUCUUGCACACGAUUGUGGUUGAAUGUAAGGAGCACCCCUUUUAAUUGCAUUACAGUAUAUCAUCCAAACCAGCAGAGUCCAAUUUCUAUACAAAUUUCAGAUGUGAAAGAAAUAUUCUAUAUUUAUGCUGUCCAAUAUGGUGGUUAGUAGCCACAUUUGCCUUUUGAGCACUUGGUAUGUGGCUAGUGUGACUGAGGAUCCAACUUUAUUAUUUUGAUAAUUUUAAUUUAAAUAAGCACACAUGGCUGUUGCACAUGCCAGCACUUAUUGGGCAAUGCAGUUUAAGUUCUAUAUCAAAGCUCUUCAGUGUUUUCUUUAUUGGCAUGUGUUACAGCUCCUAUUUAUAUGUGAGACACUCUCCCAUAGCUGUAGGCUGACAAGACAGAGAAAGUAGUGACUAAAAGUUUAGAUGCUGAAGAGACAAGUUUACAUCUUGGCUGUGGAGCUUAGUAUGUUACUCUGAGUUUAGAGCUGACUUACCCUUAAAUUGGGAUGAUUAUUGAACUACAUUAUAGAACUAUUUAAAAAAAAUUUAUUUUGACAUAAUUUCAGAUUUCAGACGUUCAGAAUAGAGACAAGAAUUGUACAAAGAAUAACUGCAUGAACUUCACUGAGAAUCUCCAAAGGUUUCUGAACUCUCUCUCCACCCCCCCUUUCUUUCUCUCUCUCUCUCUCUCUGUGUGUGUGUAUAUGUGUGUGUGUACACUUUAUUGUUUUCAUGAACAAUGUGAGAGAGUAAGUUGCUGGCUUACUCCUUUUCUUUUAGGUGCAUAUUUUCUAAAAAUAAAGGCAUGAUCUCUCAUCAGGAAAUUAACAUUCACUAGUCUUAAUACUAUUAUCUAAUCUACAGACUUAAUUCAGAUUUCAUAGGUUUCCCAAUAAUGUCUUUUAUAGCUAAAGAAAAUAUCAUCUUAUGCCUUGCAUUCCAUUUUCAUGUCUUUAAACUUCUUUAUUCUGAAACAAUUCCUCAAUCUUAAUUUGCGUUUCAUGACAUAGACAUUUUCUAAAUAAUAUAAGCCAGUUAUUUUGUAAAUAGUCUCUCAAUUUAAGUUUGUCAAAUGUUUCCUCAUGAUGAAAUUUAUUCUAUGCACUUUUGGUGGCAAUACCACAGAAGUGAUGAUGUGUCUUUUGCAAUGCAUCAUAUCAGAAGGCCCAUGGUAUUCACUGCCCCAUUAUGGUGAUGUUAACUUCAAUCACUUUAUUAUCGGGUUAAGGUGCUGUCUAUCAGAAUGGUGUUUGCUAGUAUAGGCAAUGUCUGCCAAUAAUUUCAAUGUAGUUAUUACUUUUUCCCUCUGUAAUGAAAAAUAUAUUGGGGAAAGUUACAUUGAGAAUAACUAAAUAUCCUGUUGCUGCCUCGAAUUUUUACACACUUCUUUUUGCACUUAUUCAUGAUUCUUAUGUGAAUUCUUAUGAUGAUUGCUAAAUAGAGAUUUUCUAGUUCCAUAUUUUCUUUACAUUUAUUAGUCGAGUUUCCACCUGAAAAACAGCUUUUUUCCACCUAAUUAUUUAUUUAUAUCCUGGUAGACAUAUAUUAUUCAAUGGGUUGUCAUCCUUUAUGUCAUUACAUAUAAUACAUGUGAAUAUACAUAUAUAUGUAUAUAUAUUCUUUAUAUAUAUAAAUAUAUAUAUUUGUAUAUAUUUCUUUAUAUCUUUGAUGCUCAAAUUGUCCUGGAUUUGAGUUAAGGGAGCUCCUUCAAGCUAGCUUCUACGUCCUUUUGAUGUGUCUCCAUAAUUCUUUGAAUACAUCCCUAAUUUCUGGCACAAGAUGAGGUUUCAUAAUGAUUUUCUACUUUCCCUCACUAGCCCUGGAAUCAGUAAUUUUCCUAAAAUUCCUUUAUUCCUUUGAGUGAAAAGUAUUUAGAAGCCUAGAUCAUGGGCUAGGUCUUCUUCUUGUUGCUACUGGGUGUCAUUGCUUCUAGGCCUUCUCAGCAGAUAGCCUGGAAGUAGGACUUGAAAUAUUCAUGAAUGUAUAAUUAUCUAUAUGAAUAAAUACAUAUAAAGGCAUAUAUAUUUAUACAUGUUUAUGAGUAUAUGUGUCACUACAUAUCUAUUUCUAUUUUUAUGCCUAUCUAUGUAUCUAGCUAUCCAUCUUAAAACUCUUAAAUUCAAACUGACGCCUCCAAAAUCAACACCUUGGAGUUCAUUCUAUCUUCUCCCUUUUCCAUAUUUGUAAUUCCCUUCUCUAAUUUAGCAAAACUUAGUUACCAUUGGCCACAAUUUAUUUUAUUUCUUUGCUCACCUUAGAAUAUAUAGAAACUAGUUUCCAAACUGUUAAUCUAGGAAUCUGAGCAAAAGCUACUCACUAGAAUUGAAUAUUUGUUCAGAGUUGUCUUCAGACUCAGAGUACAUAGUUCUAAUAGUCAAGGUUCAUAUAGUUCAAAAGUUAACUGAGGUUCCCCCUAAGCUGUGUGGCCAUGUUAUUCAUUUGAAAUAUGACUCUGUUCAUGUUUUUGUUUUAGGUUUUUAGUUCUAGGAGUUUUUUCCUCCCAUGCUUGUUAGUUUUCUAUUCUUUUUAAAGUAUGUAUGUGAAACAUUAAAAAUUCCCAAAAGUCAGAACCAUAAAAUAUUAUACUCAAGAAGGUGUAAGUCCAUCCUCCCUUUCUUCAUAGAGCAGUUUUGAAGAGUAAAUAAUAUUAUAAAUGUUUAGAUUUUGCAUUACCUGGCACAUAUUUAGGUCUCAAAAAAUCUAAUAUAGCUAUUCAUCUAAUAAUCGCGCUUUUUCUAUGUUCAAUUACACACUCACUAAGUACUUCAUACCUUUUUCUCAAUGUAUGAAACCAAAUAAGAAUGCACAUAUGUGAACAAAACUCUUCUAAAAUUUUGGUAUUUUAACUCUUACUAGCAAAAUAUUAUUUGCAAUCUUUCUCACAAUUAAUCACGAAACAAACUAUUGUGUUUGAUUUCCUAGCUAAGAAAUAAUGGCUUAUUUCAUUCCUUAAAAAGUAGAACAUGAAUGCUGCAUGUGGCAUAAGCACAGUGUUAUUGCAGGAGUAAUAUAGAAAACAUAUCAGGGUCAGAACUCAUUUAGUGGUGCCUUAAAUGUGAAGAAAAUAGCUGUAAUUCUGCAUAAAUGUUAUAAUUGUUAGAUUGCAGAGAAACAAAGAGUCCUGAGGCAUGUCUGAAGAAAUGAGCAGAUUACAUGCUUAACUAAUUCUGGAAGAUAAGGUUUCUAGAUUAAGUCAUGCUCUGCAAGGGAAACAAAUAAAGCAAGCACUACAUCAUUAGAAUCUAUUUUAUUUUAAUGUAUUUCUUUAAAGAGAAAGCUUUGAUUCUGGAAAUGUCUGACAUUGCUGCAUUUUUCUCAUGAAGUCUUCUGUGCAUACUUAACUAGUGAUUCUAAUACGUAUAUUUUACUAGUGAUAUUCAGUAAAUAUGUCAGAGAACAGAUUUCUUCUCUUGGCUAAAUGUUUGCAAUAAAAUUUCUGGAUAAAAUUUGAAUUAUUUUCCUAUUUUGUGAAUCAUAUAUCCUUACUAAAGCAUCUUUUUACUUCUUUUUUGAUCAUGUAUAAAAGUUAUUGAGUAUCAUAAGAAAUUUUAAAACAUUUUAUUUUUAUCACAUAACAGGAAUGGAAUAAACCAAAAAAAAAGUAUACUUAGAAAACUCUUAAAUGACAAUACAACUAUGAAUCUUAAACAUUUUUGGGAAGCAAAUAGAGAUGACAUAUCAAGAUCAAAUUGUAAAAUCCAUGUAAGUAUCACCAGCAUGACAAUCUUUCUAAGAGAUGUUUACUUUUAGAUAUACUCCCUAUAUUCUUUAUAGUAUAUAGAAACUUUCUUUGUCCAUAUCUUAAUAGCAGGGUGAACUUAGAGGUAAGUUACAAGUUGCAUACAUUUAAAUGUUAAUUUUAAUGCACCUUUGGUACACUUUAUAUUUUGAAUUGAAGGGAAAUUUUAAUUCUGUAACAUAAGUAUCUUAAUAGAUACUUAAUCAUAUAUCCAGAGAUAUUAAUAGAUAUCCAGUUUUACCCAGAAUUUUCUUAAAGUAAUACACAGAUGCUUACUGAUUGGUUAGUACCCUUCUUUCACAUUUCUGAGGUCUCAUCUUCCAAAUGAGGUAGAUUCAACAACGUUUCCAAGUUGUAGCUCCUCAGGACCCAAGUCCUCUCCAUGCUGUGGCUAGGGCUUCCAAAGUCCCUCAUUUCCCCACAUCACCACUCCUCUUUAAGAUCUCCUUCUUUCCUGAUUUCUCAUACAACUUUUUUAUGCCCAUCUCUGUCCUUGAUGCUGGAGGGGGAAGUGAAACUGCCAAACAUCAUCACCAGGAUGUGCAUGAAAUCCAACCACACAUUGAACCCCAGAUUUCCUUGGGCUCUUUUGAACACCCAAUCUUUGGGUAAGAUUAUUUCUAUGAAAAUUUUGUUUCAACUUUCUAAACAAUUGAACUGUAAAUUUUACUGUAAGAUUAGUGUGCGUCAUUUAAAAAAUUUUGUGUCUUCCGUGCGUUAUGAGAUAUGUCCCAUUCUGUAAUCUCUGACCAUGGAAUCAAGCUUAAAUUUCAUGACCCUUUCUGAAAUUACAUAAGUGUCUUGAGUUUGUUUUUAACUGAUAUUCACCCGCCCCGCUUGUUGGUCUAAAUGAAGAGGAAAUUAUCCUAAUGACUUUAUUUUCCUUCUUUAGAUGAAAUUGUUAGCAUGGCAAGGAAAAAAUAUAUUAGCUUUUCCAUGUUUAUUGCAAUAAGAUUUCCAGUAGAUAUCAGGAUAAUUUAAGGCUUCCGUUGCUACAGUUGCUUGCCUUUCUCUCUUCUGGUUUUGAAAUUAUCAUUAGGAAUAAAGAACUCAUUGCUUUCUCCUAGCUAACCGUCUAUAGCAUAAUACUAAAUACCCUUUCAAAAUGAUGCUUCUAUUUGCAUUUAUGUUACUUCAUUCUACUAAUUUUCCCUAUGCUUUCACUCAAAAAGCUAUGGAUACCUCCACACUGUGUUUUUCGGUAUUUCUCCCCGUGUUCUUCUGCUGGGAUUUGAAAGUAUACACUUGAACUUGAAAUAAAUAAUAGUAAUUCAUGCAAUGUAAGAAAUAUGCUGCUAUUAUAGGAUAGGGAGAGAGAUAACUUAGAAAGACAUAAUUUGUAACAAUAAAAGUUUUGAGUAUUUUUCCUUCUUGGCUGACUUCGUUAGUAACUAUCAUAGAAGCAUUUGACACUUCAUUUUAAAGUACAGUAGUCCCCCAUUAUUCUCCAGGGAUAUAUUAGAAGACCCCCUAGUGAUGCCUGGAACUGCAGAUAGUACUGAACCCAAUUGCUGUCAAUCUUCCUGUUCAUCUUCCACCUACAAAUUUAAUACUUAUUCCACCUUAACUAAGCCCUUAUCAUACACUCUAGCCAUAACUUUUAUAGUGAAGUAUGACAGCAAAGCUUGCAUAAUUUGUUUUCCUUCUUCCCGAUUUCAUGAAUAGAAGACUCAUUCUUACCAUAGACAUUAGCAACCUCAACCUCAGCAUACUUUUUUUUUCUUUCCUUAAGUGGAGAACUUUCACUUUUUCCCUUAAAGGAAGCACUUCCCAGCUUCUGUUUGGCAUAUCCAAAUUCUCACCAACAUUACUAUUGUGCUUUGGGGUUAUUCUGAAGUCAAUUAAGGGUUCCUUGAACACAUGCACUGUGAUAUCACAGACAGUCAAUCCAUCACAGAGACGGAUACUAAGUGACUCAUGAGCAAAUAGCGUGGACAGCUUGGAUACACUGGACAAAGAAAUAAUUCACAUCCUGGGCCUGUAGGAGCAGGAUGGCAUGAGAUUUCAUCAGCUACUCAGAAUGAUGUGCAACUGAAAACUUAUGAGCUGUUUAUUUCCAAAAUUUUUUAUUUAAUAUUUUCAAACUGCACGGUAACUAAAGCCAUGAAAACCAAACCUUGAACAAGAGGGGAAUGCUGUAUAUAUGUCUGAAUCAUAUUCCAUUGGGAAUAAUUUACAUAAGAUAUACAGCAUAGCUAUAUCUGUAUAAACAACACAGGUUUGAACUGUGCGAAUCUUCUUACAGAUGAAACUUAAGAUUGUUAACUAAAAAAAAGAUGGUAGAAAAUUACAUAUAGUUUUAUUUUAUGUCUUAAAUAAUAAUAAUCAGGAAAUUUGGAUAAAUAUAUAAAAAGUUAUUAGCAGCCAGGCAUGGUGACUCACUCCUGUAAUCUCAACACUUUGGGAGGCUGAGACGGGCAGAUCACCUGAGGGCAGGAGUUCAAGACCAGUCUAGCCAACGUGGUGAAACUCCGCCUCUACUAGAAAUACAAAAAUUAGCUGGACGUGGCAGCACAUGCCUGUAGUCCCAGCUACUCAUGAGGCUGAGGCAGGAGAAUUGCUUGAACCCGGGAGGCAGAGGUUUCAAUGAGUGGAGAUUGCGCCAGUGUACUCCAGCUCAUCAGCCUGGGUGACAGAGAGAGACUCCGUCCCAAAAAAAAAAAAAAAAAAAAAAAAAAAAAAAAAAAAAGGUUAUUAGCAGCAAUUAGUUUUAUAAAGGUAGGAAGAAUCUUUACUCAAUAAUUUUACUUUCUAACUUCACAAUUUAUGUAGUGUUUGAAUGAUUUACAGUUAGCAGUUAUUACCUGUCUGAGUAGGAAAAGAUAGAGAUUUUCAAAAGACAAAUUUUAUUUUAAAAAGCCAAAUGAUGUAAUGGAAAGUUGUGGAGUUUACAGUCAGAAAAUGUAGCAGCCAUCUAAUCAUAUGACUUACUAGACUUAAUUUAUUCCUUCUGAGCCUCAGUAUUCUUACCUGUAAAAUAUGAUAAUAAUUACCAACCUAAAAGAUUGUUCUGCAAGCAACAUGUGAGAAAUGUAAGCUGCAAAUAGCAAGAUACGUCUUCUGGUUUUGUAUGUAUGAUUUUAUACUGACUUACAGAUACUUAUAAUUGAGAAAGAAUGUGGUGGGGGGAAGGGUGGUAGUGAGUAGGACCAUUUGUAAAAUGAUGAGAACAAAAUUCAAUAAAGAAAGCUCAUGUUUCUGUGAAGUGGGCUUUUUUAGAUUACACUAAUAAGUGAGAUCUAAGAGGACAGAGGGGAGGAAGAGUUAUGGAGAAAGAGGAGCUGUUGAUCCAGGGAUAAAAUUUCAGUUAAACUGGAGGAAUAAGUUUUAGUAAUCUAUUGCACUGCAUAGUGACUACAGAUAAUAAUAAUGUACUAUAUAUUUCAAAAUUGCUUAUAAUAGAUUUUAAUGUCUUCACCACAAAAAAUCAGUUGCUGAGGUGAUGAAUACAUUAAUUAGACUGGUUAAAACUUUCUGCAAUGUAUAGAUGGAUGAAAACAUCACAUUGUACCCUAUAAAUACACACAAUUAUUAAUUGUCAUUUAAAAAUAAACCAAUAGAAAAAGAAAGCUCAUGUUGAAAAUUGAAGGCAGAAAGGGAAGGAAAAUACAAUGCAAAUAUACUGUAAUACAUUUUCAAUCAAAGUAAAAUAGCUAUUCAGUGCUGAAAGUAAGGAGAAAGGGAAUUGAAGAAAAAGUAACAAAGAAAACAAAAAGUCAAAAGUUGGGAAAAAAAAAUAGAUGGAGUUAAUGACUCAGAGAUUUUUAGAAAUAGCACCAAGCUGUGAAGCCCAAGAAUGGUCAUUCAAUUUGGAAAGGAUGAUCGAAGCCUCAAUCACUUUUGUAGAUUGAUAAUGACAGGAUUAAAAUAUUUUUAAAGAUUUUCACCACUUCCCAACCUCCUCCAUUGGGAGGUUGGGAAGUGGUGAAAACUUAAACAUAACCAAGUGUUGCAAGCAAAAUUUGAUCUACUGAAUGUAAUGCAGCUCUUCAUGGCUUCAGGUUACGUGAGCAACAGGUAUAAGCUAAGCUUUAGAGUAAUAUACAGAUUUGUAAUCUUGUGCCAAUUGCUUUUCUUCCUUAAGUCUCAUUUUCCUCAUCUGUUAAAUGAGGUUAAAAAUAAUAGCUAUUCCAUAAGGCUGUCAGGAGGAAAUAAUGUGUUGCUAUACCUAAGACUGAAUAAAUGGUAAAUAUUGUUGUAGUUGUUGGAAAAUUCUCCAGGCAUUGUGCAUCGAUGAUUUAAGAAGUUAGAUAUUCAAGUCAGGCGCUGUGGCUCACGCGUGAAAUCCCAGCUACUUGGGAGGCUGAGGCAGGAGAAUCACUUGAACCCAGGAGGCGGAGGAUGCAGUGAGCUGAGAUCGCACCACUGCACUCCAGUCUGGGCAGCAAGAGUGAAAGUCUGUGGAAAGAAAGAAAGAAAGAAAAAGAAAGAAAGAAAGAAAGAAAGAAAGAAAGAAAGAAAGAAAGAAAGAAAGAAAGAAAGAAGGAAGGAAGGAAGGAAGGAAGGAAGGAAGGAAGGAAGGAAGGAAGGAAGGAAGGAAGGAAGGAAGGAGAGGGAGGGAGGGAGGGAGGGAGGGAGGGAAGGAAGGAAGGAAGGAAGGAAGGAAGGAAGGAAGGAAGGAAGGAAGGAAGGAAGGAAGGGAGGAGAGAGGAAGGAAGGAAGGAAGGAAGGAAGGAAAAGAAAGAAAUAGAGAGAGAGAAAGAAAGAAAAAGAAAGAAAGAAAGAAAGAGAAAGAGUUAGGUAAAUAUUCAGAGAGCUUCCAUCUGCCCAUAGAAUGCAGGACUUCAAUUCGCAUCUUGAGAACUGAAAUUGGUUACUUAGAACUGAGUGAACAAGUGUGUAGGCAUGAUGUAGAUUUAUUUAUUUUUCUCUCAGGAGUUAUUUUAACAAUUUUGUUUUGAGACUUCUAACAGACUUUCUGGAGCUCUCCUACCAGCUGCUAUUGUUCUGUGUCCCUUGCUGGCAAGUACUGUCUUUCAAUAGAGAUGAGCCAAUUUAUUUGAUGCUGCCUCUGGAGAAGAGAGAAGCCCUUUGGGUACAAAGUGUGCCUGUCAUGCAGAUGGCUUCUCUAAUCUAAUGAGGUAGAGAGCUGAGCAGUCAGGAGAGGAAGGAGUGUUGGUAAAAGCAGAGUCUGUUCUCUGCACCCACUUCUCCCAUCUAUAUAUGAAUAGUUAGUACAAGAGCCACUUUCUACAAGAAUCUUUAAACUUUGACAUGACUAUCCUAAAGAUGAGCACAUCUGAGUCUGUGCAUGGCUGGUGUAUCAGUGCAGUCUGUUUGGACAGCCACUUUCCUCUGCCACAAGGUGUGUUUCCUUUUUAUUCUUCGUGACAGUUUGGCUUAUAAAGUCUUCCCUUAUUGAUGCAAUUGUGAGAGAAUAAAUUUCAUUCUUCCCCUGAAUCUGUAACAUCUUUAGAAUAUAAUCUGAAUAUCAAAAUUUAGGUUUUUGGUUUGGUUUUGUUUAAUUAAUUCAUUUAACCAUAAAUACUUCUGUAAUGAGAAACCAAUUGUAGCUUAUAGAAUAACCUGAUAGUGGUGAUGAGGGAGACAUAAGCCUGCUGCCUUAAUGCUUUCUGUGCCUCAGUUUCCUCAUGCAUAUAAGUGGGAAAUAUGUCACUAUCUUUUACUGGUUUCAUAGGAUUAUAUUCAGUGCCAGUUAUAUUUGUUCUAAAACACUUGGAUAGUUAUUUGUGCCUUCAAAAUUAUCUAAUGUCAUAUGAAAAUACAAAUUUUGAAAGGAUACUAUUGCAAUGAGCUGUCAGUUUUAAAUAUUUUGAUUUGAAUUUUAUUGAAAAACCAAAUUCCACCUUAGGUUUUCUAUCUGAAAUGUUUAAAAUUUGUGUAAAUAUUAACAUCACAUGGAAAUCAUAUUCUAUUUAAAUUUUUUGCCAUCAUUUAUUUUUUAUCUGACUCUCCUUGUAAUUUUAUUUUCAAUUGCCUUCAGGGAACAAUAUGCAAACUCUUCGAGAACUCAUUUAACUCUUGUCAAUUUGUACCAAUAAAAAUCAAAGCUUAUAUAGUAUUAUGCAAAUAUUUUAUUCACUUGGAUAAGAGGGAGUCCAUUCUACUAAGUCAGUUCUUGUAUUAAAAUAAUUAUUCAUUUUGUUUCAUCAUUUCAAUUAUAGGCGCAUAAAUUCUUAUAUCUUGUCUCAAACACAAAAUCUCAGAACGUCUUACUUUCAUGCAAAAAAACUAAGUUCUAAAAAAGCAAAUUUAUAUCACCUUAAGACGUCCAAAAGUAUAAAGGUUAUUGGACAUCACUCCUGGUAUCCUUGGAAAUAUUUGUUUGAUUUUGAAGAAAGCCUCUAAGCAGUCAAGUUGAGUAAUAUUUUUAACUUACUCUUCUCGACUUUGAAAGAGUGCACCUGUGAAGAAAUAUCUAGGGCAUAGAUAUUUCCUCAUCUCUCUUUAUCAUCUUGCUUUCUACCAUGUUGGUCUGCAUAUGGUUAGAUGAAUCUGUGUGACUAAUACCAGGGCAAUCUUGACCUCAGUGUAUCAACUUCUGUGAGCCUGUCUUGUCUAAAAUGAAUUUGGCUGAGUUAUAGAGCCUCUAAGAAACUCUUACCAGAGGAAGGAAGACAAAAGUUUGCGGUGGGAAAGUGAAGAGGUCAAAAAAGGAGCUAGAACUUACUAAAUAAACAUUUUAGCAUAUAUUAUCAAUAUAAGAGUAACCCAGGAAAAUCAUUGUUAUGGCUUCUAUAUUCUUGAAUUUAGUAGUAAAAAUAAUUUGAUUUUGGCUUAAAUGUAAUGUUCUAUUUCUUAAGGUCCUGUUUCUCAAGGUCCCAUUUCUUUUCACUCUACUUGUCAAGUUCAAGACCAUUUAAAAAAUUAGUAUUUUGCUAGUACAGUUUAUUAAUAACCAUCUCAUUUAAAAGAUAGAGAUAUAUGUCAGGUGCACUCAACUUUAUGUUUCAGAUCACCUUGGAUACUGUUUUAGCAUUAGUUUAAUAAUUUUUGAUAAUUCAUCAUAAACUUCCAUCACAGAUAUUAGCAUAAAUUCUACAGGCCAAUUUUUUUAAUAAAUCCUUGUUUUACCUCAUCAAGAGAGAAAUAAAGAGUGAGAGAAAAGUGAAAGAGAGAUUGAGAUGGGGUAGAAUCCGAUAACAUUAAAAUUUAAGGGAACAUGCCUGCUUUGUGUGUUUGUCUGUUUGGUUAUUUCCAGAAACAUAGGAAUCUCAGUAGGAGAAAUUGAGUAUAAUGUUCUGUAUUUAAGGGAUGCAGUUUAUAUGUCUUUUUGGUCAAUACAGUUAUUCCCUUUAUUCAGGGGGAUAUGUUCCAAGACCCCCAAUGGAUGCCUGAACCACAGAUAGUAGUAAACCCUAUAUACACUGUUUUUACAUAUAUAUAUGUGUGUAUAUACAUAUGUGUGUGUAUAUAUGUGUGUGUGUGUAUGUGCGUGUGUACACACACACACAUACACACACACACACACACCAUACCUGUUGAUAUGGUCUGGCUGUGUCCCCAUCCAAAUCUCACCUUGAAUAACCGUCAUGUGUCAAGGACAGGGCCAGGUGGAGAUAAUUGAAUCACAGGGUGAAUCACUUGAGUCAAGGAGUUCAAGACCAGCCUGGGCAACAGGGCAAAAACCUAUCUCUACAAAAACAAACAAACAAACAAAACAAAACAAUUAGCCAGGUGUGGUGGUGCACAUCUGUAGUCUCAGCUACCCAGGAAGCUGAGAUGGGAGGAUCACCUGAGCCUGUGGGGUUGAGGCUGCAGUGAGCCAUGAUUGUGCCAUUGCACUUUAGCCUGGAUAAUAGAGCAAGACUCUGUCUCAAAAAACAAACAAAUAAAACGAAAUAACAACAACAGAAAAAACACUUGUCUUACAUCAUGUCCGGAAUUGAAAACACCUGUCACGCAGUCAAAAACUAGAUUAAUUUUCUAUGUGGAAUAUAGAAAAAGAAAGAAGUUGAAGUGGAAAAUCUGGAGCAAAAUAUUUAUAUUGAAAUAAAAUCUGAACAUUUUUUUGAAAAGAUACACUGAAAUUUACUACACAAAUAAGUCAAGGCUCUCUCUAAAGAAUGUGGCAUAUAAUUUUUGUCUUUAGAAAGUAUUAGAAGCAUGGUGAUGGCUGCACGGCCUCCACAUUCUCUGCGGGUAGAUGAAAUCUUGAAUUUAGGAAUUCAAGCAGAUCGUGCUUUCUGCCCUUAGAGAAAAGGUAUUACAUGUUGGUAACUGAGGUAUAAAAUAACCAAAGCCCAGAUCUCGUCUCGUGCUCCACGGAAAUCAUGCCUCGCCCGAGUCUAUAAUUGGCUGAAUUCAUUUCCAAUGAAUGAAAUGCAAAAACAUGGAAAAGACUAAAAUUGAAAUUUUAUAAUUUAAAAGAUUUAAACUGUGAGGAUGGUACAUCCUUGACCUAGAGAAUUUUGAAUCUGUCUUUGGACAGGUGGGCAACCAUAGGAAGCAAGUAGGUGUCUGGAGAUGGCUGCAGAGACAUCCCGUCCCCUCGGUAGCACUGAUUGCAUUUUCCAUGAAGGUUGCUCUUAACUUCAAAGCAGACACUCUGCUGUGAAGGUUCUGAGAGGUUAGUUCUGGGUCUCGUUGUUUCAAUUAAUCAUUUAUUCAAUUAAUAAAUUUUGAGCUCCUGCUGUGAAUCAGGCAGUAUGCUAGGCCCUGUGGCUACAAUAUAGGCAUGGUUCAUGUUUUCAGCAAACGACAUUUUACUGCUUUGGUAAAAAUAACAAUUCAUCAGAAGAAAGGCUAUAUACUAAGUUAUAGAACAGAACAGAAGUAAGACCCUCCAAAAAGGAAUGUGAAUAUACAAGAAUGGAUAUGAAUAAUUUUCCAAAUUAUAGGUUCAGCUUGGGUAAAGAAAACUGUGGGAUUAGUUACCCUUGCUUUAUGCUGAGAACUAAGAAAAAAUAAAAUAAAUAAAAUAAAAUAAAACCGUUCAUGUUAAUCCUUUCUAAGACAAACAUGCUUUUAUAUUCUGAUUUUAAUUUUCCAUUUGCCAAUGAAAGGCUCUUAGAUAGCAGUUAAAAGAAGUAUAUAAAAAUUAAAACAAAAAAGAAAUUAUUCCUAGGUUACUAAGUAUUUAAGAGCUACAAACAUAUAUAAAAACUAAAAAAUUUGUUGUAAAGUCAUUUGAAAAGGAGUAUACUUAUCUGUAGCCACCUAAGCUAUAUCUUAGGGCAGAGUAAGCACAGCUUGAUCAUAUAAUCUGGAAACCAGAAUUAUGUUAGCCUCAUAAAGUAUUUCCAAGUACAAAGAGUUCAUUUUCUUUGAUAAAACAAAGGAGAGAUACAGUAAUCUUAUAGCCAAGGCAAGCCUUUGGAUAUAAGAUUUUUAAAAGCUUGGAGAAAAUUAUUUUAUUAUAAUAAAAUCAAUUAUUGAGAUCCACUGUAUUUAUGUCACUUCUUUUAGAGUUACAUAGAAAUUUUAAUCUUUGUCUACAAAGAAUUACACUUUAAAGGAACAAUUUCAGUGUAGGAAAGGUUAACCGAUGAAAAUAUCAUAUAUUUGGGAAUGUUUGCUUAGAUAAGGACAUAGUAUUCAUUGUUUCCUCAUUUGUAACAUAUGGUGGUUUAAUCAGUAUUAUCUCUAAGUUUCCUGGUAACUUGAACACUAGGAUUCUUUAAACCCUAAGGAAUUAGAAUUCAAAUUAUGACUUGUGUGCUUCCUACUAUAUAAUUGAAAAGUUAAACCUUGCUUAUUUACUGUUUCUUAAAUCAUUACAUAUGUGUUACGUCUUUUAAGCGGCUUUUAGUAUAAUUCUUGUAGAUUGGCCUUGUAGGUAUGCCUGUUUAUUUUCUUUAUUCUUUAAAUUGGGUAUUUAUAGAUAAUUAGGAGGUAAGAUUAAUUACAAUUUUUCCUUUAAAAACCUACUUUUAUGUUCACUAAUUAAAAAAUGCAUAUUCUUUAUUUCUUAGUAUAUGUAGACUAUAUUUUUCUGACUUUAACCGAGUUUGGCAAUUUUGCAUGAACAAGCAAGGGACACUUUAUUCAAGACUAUUGCAGUAGGAAAGGAAGGCCAGAAUUCAGUCUGAGCUCAACUCCACUGAAAUAAAAGGCAGAAAUGUUCUUAAAAGCAGUGGUGGGGGAAUGUUAAGCCAUAGGUGUUUGUUAAUUGUCUUUACCAAAUGGAAAGGAAAACUUUCUCAUAUCUUCCAGGCAAGGGAUGGCUUUGCAACUUGGAGCAAGGUACCCCUGAAACUUAGGCUUCUACCCUCCAAAAGACAGGGGAAUAGGAGCUCUAUCUUCCUUAAUGAUGACAUUUCAAAAGGAUGGCUCCCAGGUCCUUGAGAAAGACAUUUCUGGUUAUAAAACUGACAAGAAGCUUUUUUAAAGAUUUACAUUUCAAAGGAGGAAAUAUUUUGCAAUUACAAGUUUUCUAAAGCAAAUGCUCUAAGAAAAAAGAGAUCAAGGGCCUAGAAUCAGGAAGCAGCCUGUCUAAAAUUUAGUCAAGCUGAGGGGAAUGUUUAGUCCACCUUGGCCAAUAUAUUAGCCUGUAAUUUAACUUUUUUUUCGAGGUCCUGUGAUUGUGGGCCUUCUGGGUAUGACUCAUUUGGACUCUUGGAGAUAGGAGGAACAGUAGGGAUGAUGCUUUGGGUACUCUCCUUUACUCUGCUAUCCACUAUUUAUUUCUUGAGAAGACUUUGUGGCCUUUAAAUUCUAUAAGUUGAGUAGAAAUUAAAUAUUUAUUCUGGUAACAAACAAUGAAAAUGUAUCUUAAAUCAGUGAGAUUGCAUAGAAGAGGAUUAUCAUUGAAACACAAUUAUUAAUAAUAUUUUUAGUACUUUUUUUAGACCGUAAACAUGAUGGGGAAUAAAAAAGAGAGGUUGUUAUAUUACAAAGAUAAAUAAAUUCAAAUGUAAGUCAAGAUAAGCAACUACUUAAAUAGAAUAGCCAUAUUCUUCUAUUAGCUGCUUCUUACCUUCCAACUGAAGUUAAAAGAGAAACGGUGUUUAUGUGUCAUUUUAGUAAGAAGACUGUAAUAAUUACAAAUUACUUUUUUCCUUCAGAAUCUUCUCAACAAAAAGCCACAAUUUCUGGAAAAUUCUAUAGUGUGCUAUAAUGCUGAAAAUAAUUCAGAAUAAAUUUGCUCAUAAAAAUGUCAGUAAGAAAAGCUAACUGGAUAAUUUUUAUUUCUCUGAAAGCCAGAGCUCUCUAAUAUCUGCUUUUGGGAUGCUGCUUAGGGUAAUUAGGUAUGAUUUUCCAGUUACUUGGGGACGAGCAGAUGUGACUGGUAUUGCUGAGAUCCUAAUUUUAUACUGCUAAUGCAAUGCUUACCAUACAAAGGCAUGUGAAGGUGAGACAGUUAAAAGUCGAUGUAAAGACUGGAAACUGGGAGUCUUUGUACUAUAUUUAAAAUAAUUACAACUAGGGCUAAAAAUAAUUUUAUCUUUGCAUUUCUCUUUUUUCUUUGUUUUCAUCCACCAUUCCCAUAGCACCUGAAUUCUCAGGGUCCCUCCUCUCCCUUUCCACCCUUUUCCUUCUAUUUCUUUCUCUUUUAACACAGCUUUUCUCCAGGAAAAUAGGACACAGAAAGAACAUCUACCUGCAAACAGCCAUCAGCGAGUAAGUCCAGAUCAUGCCAGUAUUCAGUAAGCCAUGUCUGACAACUCACCCUUUCCUCUGAGUUUAAUAGGAUAAAGCUAGUAGUGGAAUAGAAAUUGAGAAAUGUGGCUCUACUGAUAAGGAAACCUUGUCAUAAAGUAUGAAUUAGCAGCGGUUGAGCAGAUUUACUUCAGGAGUGUUUCACUGCUAUUAUAUUGCCUGUUUUAUCCUUUGGCUUCUAUGGACAUAUCAUCUGAGAUAAUGACCCUCCAUCUAUUUGCACAGGUGCAAGUAAAAAGGUCCUAAAAUGGACACACAAACUCACACACAUGCACAAGUAAGCAUGCCAAGCAUACUAAAUUACAGAAACGAAUAACUCAUCAAUAAAGCAAAUGUUAUAAAGUCCUGUGACUCAUCAUUCAUGAUUUACUCAUAACACAAAUUAAAAAAUAAUUUUGAAAUAAGUUGACAGAUUGGACCAGAGGAUAAAUGUAGGCUAUCCAGGAAGUAUAACUCUGUACAGUAACACUAAAGGAACAGCUGCCGUCUUUGUGUAGCUCACACACAGUCUGCUUUUAUAGACCCUAAUGAGGACAAAACCGAUUAGCAGAUUAGAAAUUGACAGAAAUCAGAGACACUCUGCUUAAGAAUCACUAAAGUUGGAUAGUAUUUCAACUAAUGCUAUUCUUUGUUCAUCUAAAGAUUUAUGGAAUGAGUGUCUUAUGUAUAAACAUCUGCCUCUUCAGGGAAGCAUCUGUCAUGCAGCCACCAAAUAACAUGACAGAGGGGUACUGUGUGCAUCUGAAGAGCCUUAAGAUCUGUGGUAUUGCCCAAGUUCCUACUGCAGAUUAAAACUUUUAAUCAGGUAGUUUUUAAAAAAAAUAAAAUAAACCUAGCUCAUAAAAUGAACUGUUGAAUAGUUUAAUGUAAAAGAAAGCAUUUCAAAGGAUAUUUCAUUUAAAUGCAAAUGUGGACUAUGAGUUAUUAAAGAGAAUCGAGUUUUCAUAUUCUUGUUUUUCUAGACUCCUGGGAUCAAAGUCACCUUUUGAACUUGCAAAUUUUGUGUAAGGAUUCACUCAGUAUAUCCAGAAGUCACCUUGACCAUGAAAAUAAAUCUGCUGCAAAUUACAGCCUCACAAUUAACUCAAACAUUAUCAUCUAUUAUUUGUGUUCUCUGACUUGAGGAGCAGUUCUGGAAGCUGGAAACUCCUGGAUCAAGGCCCUGGCAGAUUCUGUCUGGUGAGAGCCCAUUCCUUAUGGUGGUAACUUCUAUAUGUCUUCCCACCACAGAAGGGGGAAAACGGGAAAACUAGCAAGAGCUAGCAAGAACUAGCAAGAGCUUGAACAAACGCCUGGACUCAGAUUGGAAGACUGCUCAUUUGUCUACUGCCUCAUUCCUGGAAAUUGCACUGGAACUGUCUGAUUAAGAAAAACAGAAUAAUUCUGAAAGAAAGAAAACAAAGAAAAACAUACUCCAGAAUUCCUAAUAGAACACUUCACCUGAACCUAAAAUGGUGAGCGAGAGUCACCAUGAGGCCCUGGCAGCCCCGCCUGUCACCACUGUCGCGACUGUUCUGCCAAGCAACGCCACAGAGCCAGCCAGUCCUGGAGAAGGAAAGGAAGAUGCAUUUUCUAAGCUGAAGGAGAAGUUUAUGAAUGAGUUGCAUAAAAUUCCAUUGCCACCGUGGGCCUUAAUUGCAAUAGCCAUAGUCGCAGUCCUUUUAGUCCUGACCUGCUGCUUUUGUAUCUGUAAGAAAUGUUUGUUCAAAAAGAAAAACAAGAAGAAGGGAAAGGAAAAAGGAGGGAAGAAUGCCAUUAACAUGAAAGAUGUAAAAGACUUAGGGAAGACGAUGAAAGAUCAGGCCCUCAAGGAUGAUGAUGCUGAAACUGGAUUGACAGAUGGAGAAGAAAAAGAAGAACCCAAAGAAGAGGAGAAACUGGGAAAACUUCAGUAUUCACUGGAUUAUGAUUUCCAAAAUAACCAGCUGCUGGUAGGGAUCAUUCAGGCUGCCGAACUGCCCGCCUUGGACAUGGGGGGCACAUCUGAUCCUUACGUGAAAGUGUUUCUGCUACCUGAUAAGAAGAAGAAAUUUGAGACAAAAGUCCACCGAAAAACCCUUAAUCCUGUCUUCAAUGAGCAAUUUACUUUCAAGGUACCAUACUCGGAAUUGGGUGGCAAAACCCUAGUGAUGGCUGUAUAUGAUUUUGAUCGUUUCUCUAAGCAUGACAUCAUUGGAGAAUUUAAAGUCCCUAUGAACACAGUGGAUUUUGGCCAUGUAACUGAGGAAUGGCGUGACCUGCAAAGUGCUGAGAAGGAAGAGCAAGAGAAAUUGGGUGAUAUCUGCUUCUCCCUUCGCUACGUACCUACUGCUGGUAAGCUGACUGUUGUCAUUCUGGAGGCAAAGAACCUGAAGAAGAUGGAUGUGGGUGGCUUAUCCGAUCCUUAUGUGAAGAUUCAUCUGAUGCAGAAUGGUAAGAGGCUGAAGAAGAAAAAGACAACAAUUAAAAAGAACACACUUAACCCCUACUACAAUGAGUCAUUCAGCUUUGAAGUACCUUUUGAACAAAUCCAGAAAGUGCAGGUGGUGGUAACUGUUUUGGACUAUGACAAGAUUGGCAAGAACGAUGCCAUCGGCAAAGUCUUUGUGGGCUACAACAGCACCGGCGCGGAGCUGCGACACUGGUCAGACAUGCUGGCCAACCCCAGGCGACCUAUUGCCCAGUGGCACACCCUGCAGGUAGAGGAGGAAGUUGAUGCCAUGCUGGCCGUCAAGAAGUAAAGGAAAGAAGAAGCCUUUCUGCAUUUGCCCAUAUAGUGCUCUUUAGCCAGUAUCUGUAAAUACCUCAGUAAUAUGGGUCCUUUCAUUUUUCCAGCCAUGCAUUCCUAACACAAUUCAGUGGUACUUGGAAUCCUGUUUUAAUUUGCACAAAUUUAAAUGUAGAGAGCCCCUAAGUCCUUCAUCAUACCACUGCCCUCCAAAUCUACUCUUCUUUUAAGCAAUAUGAUGUGUAGAUAGAGCAUGAAUGAAAUUAUUUAUUGUAUCACACUGUUGUAUAUACCAGUAUGCUAAAGAUUUAUUUCUAGUUUGUGUAUUUGUAUGUUGUAAGCGUUUCCUAAUCUGUGUAUAUCUAGAUGUUUUUAAUAAGAUGUUCUAUUUUAAACUAUGUAAAUUGACUGAGAUAUAGGAGAGCUGAUAAUAUAUUAUACGGUAAAUAUAGUAUCGUCUGCAUUCCAGCAAAAAUAUCAACUCGUAAGGCACUAGUACAGUUAAACUGACAUCUUAAAGGACAACUUAAACCUGAGCUUUCUAUUGAAUCAUUUGAGUACCAAGAUAAACUUACACCACAUACUUGGUGGGUGAAUCCAAUUUUGUAGAAUUCCUACACAGGCAAAAUAGCAUGAUCUGAGCAGCAGCAUCCAGGCUGACCUCAAGGAAGCAUAGCCACAAAACAGAAUAGCACCUGUCUGUACAUAUUUACAAAGCUAAAAUAAUGGCUUCACUCUUAUAUUUGAGGAAGCAACUGAACAGGAGUCAAUGAUUUCAUAUUACUGCAUAUAGAAUAACAACAAGGUGUUCCGUGUGUGUGUGUGUGUGUGUGUGUGUGUGUGUGUGCACAUUUGUUUGGGGAUGGGGGAGAAGAAGCUAAGGGGAGAAGUCAACAUUUAUGAAAUAUUGCCUGACUAUUUAAAAAGAAAAAAGUAGCUCUCCAUUAUCACCUUUAUACAAAAUGUACAUCCUGUGAAUUCUGUUCCAGAUUUCACACCUACAAUAAUUCCAAAAGGUUUGCACAUUAGAGUUUGUAACAAAAUAUUUUAUUAUAUAAAACCAGGUUAGAAGGAAUGCAGGAUAUUUUUAACACAACAAUCUGUGCUUAUUACACAAAAUUACUUUGUGGUAAACAGACAGUAUUGUAAUCCCAUCAAAAGAUGAAAGAAAAACAAAAACAAAAACCAACAACAAUUAGCCAUAGUUCUGAAUGCACUUCAAUUAAGCCAAAACAGACAGCUAGUGAUCUUUUUAUAUGCUCUUUUUACUUAAGUUUUAAUUUGUCCUUUAAAAAAAGGUGAAACAAACCAAGAACAAGUUCUAGAAAACUGAAGCAACCUCUUAUGUAUACUAGAUGCUUGAUUUAGGAGGAGUUUUUAAACGUUUUCAAUGUUAUUAUGUAGUAAAUGACACUAUUAUGAAGCUACUAGUCAUUCCAUAAGAGUCUUAAAGGACUGCUCUGUGUAACACUGUGACUGCCGUGUGUGCUUAGACCCGUAGUUUCCUCAGUGGAUAGCACUCAAUUUAUUCCGUAGUGAUAUUGUAACAAUACUGCCAUUCCCUUCUACUGCACUGCCCAAGGUGUGUGUAGCACAAACAGUUCUCAUUACAAAGGACCAAUUCAGAACUGAAAAGCUAUGCAUAGGACAAGGAAGAUACAUAGAAUGGGGUGGAACACAGCAUUUUGUCAAGCACUGUGCAAUAUUCCAUAUUUUUCCCCACUAUGGUAGACAACCAUUUCGUGGAAGGGCAGCCUAUUAUCCCACACUGCAUCUAGCCUUUUGUCCCAUUCACUUCUGUGAUCCAUUUUAAUUUCCAGGCCACAAGACAGUAGUGAUGCUCUGAAAUGAAAGUUUGUCUUCACAAAUAUCAAAACAAAAUGGAGGAAAACUAAGCAUUGGCCUCAUGUUCAGUCUUCAGGAUAUCACACCACGUCUUUUCAAAAACUAAAGAGAAUUCAAAAAGGGCUGAUGGUAGGCUUUGAACAUGGGGUUGGCUGUUUCCCAGUAAAACUGGAAUUCCUGUCGUUACUGUUUCCUUAUCAAAGAAGGGGCAAGCUCUUUUGCCUUUUAGGCCAGACAUAGCAAACGCUUUAUAAUUGGCAUAGACAUAAAGGAUAAAAGGAAAAUAACCGUCUGCCGAUGGUCCGUACUUCUUAAAAAACAUAGGUAAUAGAAAAUAUACACAAGUCAGAAUGUGAAAUUAAAUAAUGGUUUGAACAGAAAAUUCAAACAAGACUCUUUCCAAUUUAAAGGGCCAAACCCUACCAAAGAGAGGGAGUUGACUGGCUUUUAAAAAGUAUUUAAAUACCACAAAUGACAUUUAAUUUCACUGUAUUCAGCUUUAAGUUGUUCACAAUGAAACCACACUUUCAAACAAGCAGGUUCAAGCUGCUGAAUAGACAUUAUUUCUUGCAUUAAAAUACCACUAAUGCAUUCUCUUGCAACACUGCCAGACAUGGGAUUGUCACCAUAGAAUUAGUUGGUACUAUGCCAUCUUUCACUCUUUCACAAGUCAGUGAUGGAACCUGCUUUAUGACCAAGAUUCAUCCUCAAAUAAGCCACAUGUACCCUUCUGACAAAGCUGUGUAAAGUAUUAGAAUCUGAUGCUCUAGAAAGAUCCUAGUUGCCUUUGUGUAUAUUUACUGCCUGCUUGAGUGUUUCUAUGUGUGGGUUUUCCCUGUAUCUUGUAGAAAUGUUGGGGUGUUUUCCUCUGCCAUAUGGCUCGUGGCCUGCGAGCCAACUAUUUCAGCUGUAUUUUACCUUCAUUUUUGAUGAGGUGAUUUAAAUUUUGUUUCACUUUGUGUAGUGAAUUCCACAGUAGUUUUCUGAUUGUUGUUAAAAAUGACUUAACAUAUUACACAGAUAUUCAAUAAAAAUGUUUUAUUUCCUGUUGA